GAUUACAGGUGCCAGCCACCAUGCCCGGCCAAAAAUCUCUACUUGUUCUUGGCAGUCUCCAUUUUACUGAAGCUGAAAACAAAAGUUAAUUUUACUAGAAAUCAGAAAUAUUUUUCUCUAAGAGACUAUGAAGUAUCAAAUGUGAGCAAUGAAAGAAAAUUGGGCUAAAUAAUUUGAUACAGGAAAAAUUAAUUCCGGAUAGAGUCCAUGCCUCAUGUCAGUAUUUUUUGCCCAAAUUCAUGUGGAGAGCUCCUCAUUGGUGCCCCUUCACACUCCAGCCACUAUUGCAAUGAGGAGGUGAGGAGAGAUGUCUUAUCUUUGCCUGGAGCUUCACUGUUCUGUGCAUGUGGCCUAUAGACCAGCAUCAGCAUUGCCUAAGAGGUUGUUACAAGCAGAAUUUCGGGCCUCAACCUACCUUACAGAAUCUGAAUCUAGGUGAGGCAUGAUGGCUCACACCUGUAAUCCCAGCUCUUUGGGAGGCCAAGGUAAGUGGAUCAUCUAAGGUCAGGAGUUCGAGACCAGCAUGGCUAACAUGGUGAAACCCCAUCUUUACUAAAAAUUAGCCAGGUAUGAUGAUGGGCUCCUGUAAUCUCAGCUACUCAGGAGGCUGAGGCAGGAGAAUUGUUUGAACACAGGAGGCAGAGGUUGCAGUGAGCUGAAAUCACACCACAACACUCCAGCCUGGGGGACAGAGCAAGACUCUGUCUCAAAAAAAAAAAAAAAAAUCAGAAUCUACAUAUUUUAACAAGACCCCCAGAUGGUUCAAUUCUUCAUUGAUGUUUGGGAAACACUAUUACAGAGAACCUUUUUAUGAAGUUAUGGUCAAUUUUGUAGACUUCAGCCUGGCUAAUAACUCAGAGACAAAUUAUGACUAUGGAAGGUUAUUUCUUUUGUCAAGCUAUGGAAUGGAAUCAUUUCUCUCUUCAAGUCACCCAUGCCUUGCAUGUCCUGGGAAAGAGAGGGAAAUGACGCUUACUACAAGUUAAUAUCUUACCUCUUCCCAGACCAACUUCUAUUAUAUACACUGACUGCUAAUGAGGUGUAACAGGAUAGACCAGAAUUGAGUCUGGCCUCUGGCCCACAUUAACCAUAUAAAAGUUGGACAGCUUCCUUAGGUUUUUCCAUCUCAUUUUCCUCUUCUGUAAGAUGAAAAUUAUAAUAAUUCUUGGUAAGAAUGUUUUGACAUUAGAGGUGGGGAUGAGAAAUUAUCUCCUAUAGCUUGGCACAUUGUAGGCAUUCAACAAAUAAACAGACGCUGUGGCUACUGGAGUUCCUCCUGGCUCCUUGGUGAGAGUAGAGAGGUAAUCUCGUUUUUCCAAUAUAAUCUUUUAGGUGUUUGCCUCAGGUACCUCUUGGAAGUAGACACUGAGGAUUUCAGUUUGUUUGACUUCCUGCCAGCUGAGUUCAAGAGGACAAGCUAAUGAAUACCUUAUGUUUCUUGCACACACACUUACAUAUCGGGAUAAAAUAUUCCUGGGGACAUACAAAGCAAAAGAGGAAACUUGUGUCCCACAUAAUCUCUUUCUUCUUCUAAUAAAACAAAUUUAGGCCACUUCUCCAUAAGAUUGUCAAGGAAGGUUAAUGUCAGAAUUUGCUAGGAAAGGGGGUUACUUCGUUAGCUAAGAUAGAGAAGGAACCCCAUCUCUACUAAAAAUACAAAAAUUAGCCAGGUACGGUGGUGCAUAUCUGUAACCCCAGCUACUCGGGAGGCUGAGGCAGGAGAAUCGCUCGAACCCAGGAGGUGGAGGUUCAAGUGAGCUGGGAUCACACCAUUGCACUCCAGCCUGGGCAACAAGAGCAAAACUUCAUCUCAAAAAAAAAAAAAAAAAAGAGAGAAUUAAAGUCCAGUUGUAGGACUCUAAGAACUGUCAUUACCUGGUGGUUUUUGUUUUAUCAGGGUGGAAAUUUUAAUACAGGAACUGUUACACCAUUGUUACACUCCAGCUGACAAUGUAGCCUUAAAAAUAUUAUAUAAUGAAAAAAAUACAGGUUAUAAAAGGCAGGUGCUCUCAGAGAAACUGUUGAAAGCAAUCUCCUUUAUUUUCUUUCCUUAUUUGUUUAUUUUAUUUUUUUUUUGAGACGGAGUCUCGCUCUGUUGCCCAGGCUGGAGUGCAGUGGCAUGAUCUUGGCUCGCUGCAACCUCCACCUUUCAGGGUUCAAGCAAUUCUUCUGCCUCAGCCUCCUGAGUAGCUGGGAUUACAGGCACAUGCCACCACGCUCGGCUAAUUUUUGUAUUUUUAGUAGAGACAUAUUGGCCGGGCUGGUCUCGAAGUGCUGACCUCAUGAUCCGCCCACUUGGCCUCCCAAAGUGCUGGGAUUACAGGUGUGAGCCACCAUCCCCAGCCUCCUUUAUUUUCUUAAAGAACUAACUUGAAAAUAAAAUUGAGAAACCUGCCUUAGAAAAUAGGGAAAAUGUGUGAUAAAAGAAUCACAUAAAACUUACACAUUAAGAUACUCAACUAUUAAUCUGCAUGUUAUUUCAUUAUAGCAAUAUGAAAUAAAAUAAUAGGUAUUUUUUUCUAAUUAACAAUUUUUGCUCACAACUUUAUAUUAGCAUCAUUCUUUAAUACAACUAAUGGUUUUAACAACAUGACAUUCAAAUUCUUACAUUGAAAUGAACAUUGUCACAUUAAAUUUGCCAUUUUAACAUUCACAUCUAGAGAAAAUAAGAGAUUCUAAUUAACUUUUAAAAAUUCUCCUUUUGGUUACACAAAUUUUAAAGAUUUAAUACAAGGCAUAUCCCAACCAUGCUGUGAAAAAAAAUUAUUUGUGAUUUCAUUACUUUUAGCUGUUUUCUUGGGUUUAAAUGAGGAUUAUGUAAGCAUCUUAGUGCCAUGUGUCUUAAUCUAGAAACAAAUUUAUAAUUUAAAAAUAAAGCAAUUCAUUUAUAUUUCUAUACAAAUAAUUUUAGGUAGGCCAGAUGUUCAAAUUUGAAGUUCUAGUGUAAUAUUAAAAUAAUUAUAGUUUUUUUUUAUUAUUUCUGACUCUGGUAGACUUGAUUACUUAAUAUGGAGACUAUUUUGUUAUUUUAUUGACAUUAAUCGCUUUAAAAAUGUAUUUCUGACAGUGAUUUUCCCAAAAAUAUGUUUAUAUAGGUAGAGUUGUAUUUGCAUUCCACGAAGUCAUCACUUUGUGGAUGAGUGCCUUAAGCAAAGAUUCAAUAUCUACUAUGUGCCAGAUUUUGGUUCGAUGCUGAAGAUAAAGAUAUAUUUAGGCCCAUAAGAAGCUCAUAAUUUAGUGUGGGAGAUAGACGUGUAAACAAAUUAUUUGAAUGUGACAGAUUAACUACCAGAGUAAUGCGAAUAUAUGGGAAAGAAUAAAUCACUCUACCUGGGUGUAACUUAAGGUGUGGAGGAACCUACAUAAGAUUUUGAAGAAUGAAUAUUACUCUUUCAAUUGUAGAAGAGAAUAGGAUACUUCAAGGAGAAGAAUUUGUAUUGUCUGAGAUGCAUAAGGAGCAUUGUUUGCCCAAAAAAAUGGUGGCCUAGUCAACACAGAUAUGAGGCAAUGUGUAGAGCAAAAAGAAUGAGACCCUUUUGUGAUGGAGAGGCUUCAUGUGGCAAGCUCUGUGGUCAUGAAGCUGUUUGUUUCUUCUCACACAGAUGUGCAUGUGAUAUGUACCUAGUUCACAAUAUGGAAAGAACUUUGAUACAUAUAUCAUUUUUCUGAAGUACAUCUAAACACAUGCAAACACAUUGAAGUGUGGAGACUAAUCAAAGAGAAGUCCUGAAAAAUGGAAAUCAGAAUAAUCAUAAGUGCACUCAAUUCUGUGAAUUUGAGGCUUUGAAGUUUGUUUGAUUUUUAAAUGGAAACCAUGCAUUCUAUUUCUAGCAUACUUCAUUCGUACUACAAGUACGUAUUGAAUGCCUGCUAUAGUUUAGGCACUGUUCCAGGUGCUUGGGAUAUAUAAUAAAACAGAAAAAAAAACCCUGUCUUGUAUGAGGGAGACCAAUAGGAUACAAGAUAACUCAGUAAAAAUAUAUACAUAUUUAUGUAAUAUUUAUAAUGUUAGGUGGUGAUCACUACUAAGAGGAAAAUAAAAUAAGUAGGAAAAAGGACCGUUAAAUGUCCCAAAUCAGAGGAAGGGGGAAAGAGAUUUUUAGAAGGGAGGCCAGAGCAGGCAAUACUAAGAUGACUAAGUCAAGUGUUAAGAGAAGUGAGAGAGCUAUCUGUGGGGUGGAAAGGUACAGAAACCUUUGAUAGAAUAUGCUCUGUUUGCCAUGCUUAUUUGUCAUCCAAGAGUACUGGUCAAGUAGGCAGCUGGGUGUAUCGUUCUGGAAUUCAGGAGCAAACUCUAUGGUAAAAUGCACGUUUGGGAGUCAACUGCUUAUUAUAGUGUUUAAAGCCCUGAGAUGAAUGGCAUCAUCUAAGGACUGAGUGUGGAGAGAAAAGAACACUUUCUGUACUAAACUCCAGGGUGUAUUUAAUAGUUGAGGAGAUAAGAAGGAAUAUGCAAAAGAGACCAAGAAGUCACACCAGAAUGAGAGGAGGAAGAAGAGAGAGAGUGGUGUCCUCAAAGCCAAUGAAGAAGUGCUUCAAAGAGAGAAUGAUCAACUGUAUCAGGUGCAGCUGUUAAGUCAUAUAAGAUGAGGACUCACUAAUGUCCAUUGGCUUUAGUGACAUUGAGAGUUCAAGAUAAUAAAACGGAAAUGGAGAUAGAGAAUUCAGAUAAUUCUUUUAAGUUUUAUUUUGCUUUAUUUUUUUGUUUUUUACCAUAAAAAGAAGAAAUAUUUGAGAAAUAAGGCAGGAGCCAGAGAGGAAAGAGGGCCAAGAGGUGGAAUUUUUUUAAGCUAAAUGAAAAAUUUUAGCAUGCUUGUGUGUUAAAGAGAAUGAUUUAAGAGAGAAGAGGAAAUUGAUGAUUAUGGAGAGAGAGAGAGAGAGAGAGAAGGAGGGAGAAGGAGGGAGGGAGGGAGGAGGGGAGAUUUCAAUGUCUUUAAGUAGGUCUUAGAGCAUAAGAUGCAGAGCACAAACAGAGAGGCUGUCCUCUUCCAGGAAUGUGGUCUAUUCAUUCAUAUUAACAGGAACAAGGUUGCACUUAUGGGCAAACAAGGAGUUAGGUGGAGAGAUUUGGUGGUGGGAACUUCUAAAAGUUCUCUUCUGAUUGCAGCAAUUUCUCUGUGAAGAAGGAAGCAAGAUUAUGGUGGGAGAUGUAUUAGAGACUUUAAGGAGAAAUGGGAAGUUCUCAAGUCUAGGAAAGUGGGAAAGGGAGUGGUCUACAGAAUAAUUGGCAGGUAGCUUUAAGGGCUCACUUGAAAUCAGUGGUCAUUUUUCUCUAGCCACUUUGAGCAAUGUUGGUAAGAUAAGACGACAGAGCUGGAUUUAAUCAAGGUUGUGUGAAUGAUGAAGCAAGAGGAGCAAAAAAAUAAAGGUGAAUACGUUAAAGUGACUGCACUGAUAAAUGGGAGAAUUCAAGCUGGGUGGGUAAGAAAUGAGGUGACAAGAGUGUGAUGAGAGAUCAGCAUAUUGAAGAUCUCAGCAGGAUUGAAGGGCUGAGUUGGGAUUGUAGAGGACAGGAAUCCCAUGGUUGUCUGUUAGAAAGUAUUUGAUGUCAGAUUCUUCCACAAUACUCUUAGGUACCAUGAUGUCGCAUCAAAGUGUCUUAUUUUAAAAAGUACCCUCAUUUUGUGCAAACAUAGCUGCCAAAUGCGUGUAUUGCUGCCCAUUCCCACUAAUCGGUUCAUUCUCUGAACAACUGGCAAAAUGGCAAAUGCUGCUGUUGCAGCUGCUCCUAUAGUCCCAAUUGCCUCCAGAGAGAAAAAAAAAUAACUAAAUAUAUUAUAUUAAUAAAUGACAGAAUAAACAGUUAUUUACAGUGUGUUGUUAUUAAUCCACAUCAUUAAUAUUACCAGACUGAUGCUUGAGUUUACUUUUGCAAUGAUAGAACCACUUCAGUCUUUGCAGUAAUUACAGUGGGGAAUAAUUUAUGCUUACAUGAAUGGAUCCCAGACUUGGAUCCCCACUUGGCUGGCUAGAGCUCUGAUCUCCUGCCUGACUCAUGCCAGUGCUCUCCUUCAGGGGUAGUUGAGCUCUGCUUCUCACAUCCUCCAUUAUCUGGCAAGCACCACCUGAUAUAUAUCUUGUUUGAGAAAUGUGAAUUGUGCCUGACACUGAGUGUAAGUGACCUCGAAGUUACAUUCUUCCUAUAGUAUCCCGGAGAAUUCUCACAUGGAUUCUGGUUGUUUCUGACACUCUUAAAAUUAUGAUGCAGACUAAUAAUGGUGUUUGGGGUAAUAAAUAAAAAGGAAAUAUUUAUUUAAUAAAAUAAAAAGCUACAACCCUCUUGCACCCACAGUGCAAAAGCUUUGGCAAUAGGAGGAAGCAACACAAUUUUGACAGUGCUUGAAUUUUUGCUAAUGGCAAAUUUGUUUAUUGAGCUGGGGUGUUCUAUAGGGGAACAUACUUAUUUGGGUGAUCAAACAAAAGCAGCUAUACUUCCAAAUUUUACAUCAAACUAUAUGCCUUUGGCAUAUGAACUUACAUUUUUGGCAGAAUCAGGAGUUACAAGUUCCACCAACCAUACCAUCAACUGGUGCCUGAAAUUAUUUUGUCAAAUCACCAGUUGAAUUUCUUCAUGCUGUUUGUGGAUCAGACUUUCAGAGGUAUUUGUCUGCUGUGUAGAUACACAAGCCUUUUUCCUUGAAGACACACCUGGCCCCAAAAUCAUGAUUUUUGUUUUCACAUAUUCUGGGUGCUUUUAUUACAUUAAAUGAAACACGUAUUUAAGCCCAUAGACUCUUUGAAACAUGCUUAAAAGUGAAAUCAAAAAAAUUUUCAUAGAAUUCAGCUUUCCCAUUGCAAAUAUACAUUAAACCACUGCGUUAUAUGAAUGAAUAUUCAAAAUACUCGAGUACGUAUGUUUCCAAAAACAAAUGAAACCAAAUGAUUUUCCUAAGCUGCCAUAGUUACCACUGAGGCCAAACUAGAAUCCAAGACUCCUAAUUUCUGUCUAGUGUUUUUUUCCACCGUACAUACUUACAAAAAGUUAUUCUUGAGCUCAGGAUCAUUUAGUGUCUCUCCCGUUCUGAUAAAUUCUUACCCUUUCAGAAAAGCAUAUUUUUAAACUUCCCAUCUUCAAACGCUCUGCUAACUUAAGUAAUAAUAUGUGGAACAUAGUGUAAAUGAUAUUACUUUGGCCUGCAAAGGUUGAAUUUCAGUGCAUAUGAAAGCAAAUUCCGAGCUUUAUAAUACAUUUUUCAUAAUAGAGACCAUCCGUCAAGGUGAAAAAAGGCAUGCUAAAGCAAUGAGGGACAUUAAAGCAGAUAACUUGGUAACUAAAAUAUAAAAGGACUUCCUCAGGAAGCAGACCUGAAAUAUCAGGAUAUUUGCCUUCAUUCUCUGGUGUCUUUUAAUUUGUUUUAAAAUUAAGAUGCAAGUGGUGAAGGAAGCUGACUUAGUCAACAGAAGUGGUUAGUUUGAAAGCUGUUUUGAUCCAUUUUAGUGAAUCGUUUAGAAUUUAUACUUAGGCACAAAAUCUAAUUUUCCAAUUAAUUUCACAAAAGAGAUGCUUUUUAUAUUGAUUGCCCAAGUGUGUUCCCUAUUUGUGUCCAGAAUAUCUAAUUGGCUGAUGCUAACAAGCAAUGUCCUUAAAGCUAAUACUUGCUGCUCAACUUGAUACAGUUUUAGAGCCUCUAAGAAUUUUGAUGUGUACAGGCUAUACUCUGCAAAAUCAUUUUAACUUAAUGUGGAAAUGUCAGUGAGUCCAUGUUUAUCAUAAUGGACAUUUAAAGCGUAAUUUGUUUUACUUGGGCUUAUUAAUAACUGUUUUGUUACUAACUUUCAGCAUUUAUUUAUUUAUUUAUUUAUUUAUUUAUUUAUUUAUUUGAGACAGGGUCUGGCUCUGCUGCCCAGGCUGGAGUGCAGUGGUACGAUCAUGGCUCACUGCAGCCUCAAUCUCCUGGGUGCAAGUGAUCCUCCCACCUCAGCCUCCCUAGUAGCUGGGACCACAGGCAUGAACCACCAUGCCCAGCUAAUUUUUUUGUAGAUAGCAGGGUUUUGCUAUGUUGCCCAGGCUGGUCCCGAACUCCUGGGCUCAAGCGAUCCACCUGCCUCAGCCUCCCAAAGUGCUGGGAUUACAGGCCAGUUUUAAUAUUUAUAUAUAUAUGUACCAUUUCUUGUGCUCAUUUCUUCCUAAAUAUGCAAGUUUCCAUCAGAUAUCAGUUUUCUCUGGCUGAAGAAAUUCCUUUACCAUAUUUUAAAGUGUGGGUCUGUAUACCACAAGUGAUGAUUUUUACUUAGUCUUUAUUUCACCUUCAGUCUUGAAGGAUACUUUUACUAGGUAUAAAAUUCUCAGUAUAGAGUUUUUUCUAUCACCCGACUUUUCUGGCCUCCAUUGUCUCUGAGGAGAAUUUAGCCAUCAUUUGUACCAUACUUCCCUCUGUAUAAUAUGUCUUUUUCUCUGUGUUGAAGUUUUCUCUUAUUUAUCGUUUUCAAAAAGUUGAGAUUGAAUUGGUUAUGAUUUGAUUUUUUUUUUUUUUGCUAGUUAAGUGAAGCAGUGGGAGUGAAGAAAGAACAAAGAAAUCCGUAACUAGUUGUAAUCAGUUAGUUUGAUUUGAAUUUUUAGAAACUCUUCCUGCAGUUUCCUGAGAUACUGGAACCUGUAAAUGUAUGUCUCUUAACAAAUUCAGGAAAUUUUUGGCUAUUAUGUAUUUAAAUAUUUUUUCUGCCACAUUCUUUCUCUCUUCCCCUCUUAUGAAUCCAGUGAUCCAUAUGUCAUAUCUUUAAUAUUGUCUCACAGGUCACAGAGGUGCUGUUUAUUUCUUUGAUUUUUUUAAGACUUAAAGUUGGAUGGUUUUUAUUAAUCUUAUUUCGAAUUUACUGAUUAUCUGGUCUAUUAUCUGCUACAAAGCCCAGCUAGCAAAUUUUUUUUUCAGAUACUAAAUUUUUUACUCUUAGAAUUUCUAUUAUAUUUUCAUUUGUAUUUUUCUUCAGAGAUUUCCUGUCUGUUUAUUGAUUACUAUUUUCCUUUAUGUCCUUGAUCAUAAUUAUAAUAGCUGCCUUAAAAUAACUGUUAACUAAUUCCAUCAUACUGGUCAUCUUGUGGUCAUUCUCAUUGAUUUCUUUUAUUCUUGAGUAUGAGUGAUAUUUUCUUGUUUCUUCAUAUGUCUCAUUCUGUCCUGGAUAUUAUUUUGCUUUCUGUUGUGUCUUCUGAAAAAUGUUUAUUUUUUGUUUUAGCAGGUGGUUAAUCCCUGAAAUUUCUAAAUGAGUGACAUGUUUAAAAGCAGGCAUGUCUAAAUUCUGUCUUAUCUAUAGUAGGCAGCAGCUAAAAUAUUUGAGCCUUUUUAACUUUAACCAGGCUGCCUGGACUCUGCAUAGACAGAGGUAGUUCAGGACUUAGCCAGAUAUUUGGACAGAAUUUAAAUGCAGAAUUUGAGGCUGCCCUCUGUGGCUCUUUCCUUUCCAGACAAGAAAGAGAAAAGGAGACCUUGGCAGCUGGGAGCUAGCCUGGCAUUAACAGGUGGGCCUUGAUGUUGUUAGAAGUUAGCCAGGCAGUCACAAUAGGCUGUGGUAUUCCAUUACACACUAAAAAAAUUAUCAGAAUACAUUUGUUAGACAGGGUCUUUCUGUGACUAUGAUGAGAUUUUAUUUUUUUGAGAUGGAGUCCUGCUCUGUUGCCCAGGCUGGAGUGCAGCAGUGCCACCUUGGCUCACUGCAACCUCUGCCUCCCGGGUUCAAGCAGUUCUCCUGCCUCAGCCUCCCAAGUAGCUGGGAUUACAGGUGCACACCACCAUGCCCAGCUGAUUUUUGUAUAUUUAGUAGUGACGGGGUUUCACCUUGUUGGUCAGGGUGGUCUCGAACUCCUGACCUCAGGUGAUCCACCUACCUCGGCCUCCCAAAGUGCUGGGAUUACAGGCAUGAGCCACCAAGCCCAGCCUCUGUGACCAUGAUGAAUCAAGACAAAAAGAUCAUUCUAUCAUCAUGUUCAAAAACAGACAAAAUCAAGAACAUUAUCCAAUCCACAAGAAUGACUAAACUUCCCCUCUGCUGCUGAUAUAAGCAACUGCUACUUCUUUAGCAGUCUUUAGAUAAGAAAUAGUAAGAUACCCAACCACAGAAUUACUUCCACUUCUUACCAUUGAAUUCAGAGCAAAACACUGCUUCCUUGAAGAGUCCCCAAAAGAACAUAACACAAGCCCAAAUUCUAGCAUAUAUCAGACUCACCUUGUUUCCCUGUGGUAUAUGUUCUUCCUUGUUUUCUGGUGAUCUUUGAUUGAAGGGUUAUGACACAGGAUUUCCUCCUCUACUUUCUACUGUCUGUAGUAGACUAUAAGUCUGAUCUCUCAUUGUUCAAGCCAUAAAACAAUAGAACUUCUAUGCAACUUCAAGCCAUUCUGCAUGGUGCCACACGUGUGUCUGCCCUGUGGCAAAAAAUUAGAACACUGGGAUACUUACCUGGUGCCAUUACCUUUUUUCUAGUUUCUGUGUACUUUUGGUUGUUUCCCAGUGCUUCCAGAUAAUCAUAUAUUAUAGUUUGUCCUGAGUUGAUAGUUGUUAUCUCCAGGAAAUUGUUCUGUUGUGAAUUACUUCACCAUUAUCAAAAGCAGAAAUUCCCUUUGUUGCUGUUAAAAUAUAUUACUUGGUAUCAUGCAGUCUGUUCCUAAGGUGGGCAAUCUUUCUGUGAUACCACAAUUGAGUAGUAGCCAUCAUAUUUCAUUGCAGUAGGGAAGCAUUAAAUUGUAAUUGCUAAAUGAAUAAAGUAAUCUAAAUUUGGAAGCUUGAGAGGGCCAAUUAGGUCAUUCGUGUGAGGUUUGCUGGACUUCUGUCGUCCUUUUGCUGAGCGUGAGUCAAAAGACUUCUCUAAACAAUACAAUUACAAGAACGUGUUUGUCCAUUUCCAAGUCUAAUUUUAGGAAUAAUGUGAAAGUUUCAUGGAUGAAAAUCAUUACAAUAUGUGUAUUGAUCUGGCCUGUAAUUAUUUUGCUGGAAAAUAUUGAAAAAUUUCUAACCAGUGCUUUUGGGGAAAUACUUUGUCAUUAGAACAACAAUGAUGCCUUGAAAUUAAAGUUGACGUAAUCAUUAAUUUUCUGAAACUUUUUACAAAGUUUUGUACUUAGCCAUUAUAUAUCAGGGAACAAGUGGUUAUCUCAUUUCUUAUGGGAAUCAAGACCUCUAGAAGCAUAUUCUUUUUCUCUAUCAUUUAAAGUCCAGUGUAUUUCUCCCAUGGGUUAGAUUUGUCUGUGUUCUGUCUAGAGAGACAAAUCUUUAACAUUAUUUACUCUUAGGAUUUCUCUCUAACUUAUGAGUAACAUACAUCAUUAUUCAUAUAGACAAGAUGUGAGAUUUGGAAAUACUUUUGUGUUUCUUUAGCCAUUGGAUUAUAUUGAUGUAAAAUUUAAGUGCUUUCUUGUUUUUCAUUAUAUCUGUCGUAUAUCAGCAUAUUAUAGAAACCUUUAUAACACUUCUUUAGAAGUGUGAAUAUUGCUUUGCAAGAGCGAAAAUUUAAUACUAAACCUGCCCUCCAGCCUCACAAUUCUCCCAACAUUCCUAUGAUUUCUCUAGCCCACCAUAUCUGUUCUCCAGAGGAAACACUGCUGCCCUCCACAGUUUAUCUUCCUAAUGUAUUUGCUUGUGUUUUUUGUUAUGUGUAUUGUCUGACUCCCCCUACUAGAAUGCAGGAUCUGGAAAGAGAAGUGCCUGUUUUGUUUCCAGAAGUUAUCUUGUAAGACAGGAGCAGUCUUGGCAUAUAAAAAUUGCUGUCAAUUCGUUAGUUCAACCAUUGUGGAAGACAGUGUGGUGAUUCCUCAAGGAUCUAGAACCAGAAAUACCAUUUGACCCAGCAAUCCCAUUACUGGGUAUAUACCCAAAGGAGUAUAAAUCAUUCUACCAUAAAGACACAUGCACACGUACACACAUAUGUUUAUUGCAGCACUGUUCACAAUAGCAAAGACUUGGAACCAACCCAAAUACCCAUCAAUGAUAGACUGGUUAAAGAAAAUAUGGCACAUAUACACCAUGGAAUACUAUCCAGCCGUAAAAAAGGGUGAGUUCAUAUCUUCUGCCAGGACAUAUAUGAAGCUGGAAACCAUCAUUCUCAGCAAACUAACACAAGAACAGAAAACCAAACACUGCAUAUUCUCAUUCAUAAGUGGGAGAUGAACAGUGAAAACACAUGGAGAUGGGGAGGGGAACAUCACAUACCAGGGCCUGUCGGGGUUGGGGGCUAGAGGAGGGAUAGCAUUAGGAGAAAUACCUAAUGUAGAUGACAGGUUGAUGGGUGCAGCAAACCACCAUGGCACGUGUAUACCUAUAUAACAAGCCUCCGUGUUCUGCACAUGUAUCCCAGAACUUGAAGUAUGAAAAAAAAUUCUCAAUAUGUAUUUCUUAAAUGAAUGAAGAAAAAUUGUUUAUAUAAAUCAAAUUUUUCUUUGGAGGAAGUAGCAGGAGUUCUCCCUGCCUCCUUCCUCUCUCUCUUCCCUUUAAACUAUCUGCCAGCAUCAUCUAUAUAAAGCACAGUCCAGGUCUUUUUUAAUCUUUCCUCAAAAAUCUUUAACAUCUCCCCAGUGCCUAUAAAAUAAAAUCCAAACUCCCUAGCUUGGCAUUUGAGGCCCUCUGCAAUCUAUCCUUAUUCUGCCAACAAUUUCAUCAACCAACGCUCCCCUUAUGCUUCAGCUCUUUCCAGUGUGAUCUUUGGGCUUUCUUUCUCAUUGACAUGUUUAAAUGUCGUCUUUGUUUUGUGGCCUAUGCUGAUUACCUUAUUUCUAAUGGAAACCACAUUCCCCAUCUCCCUUUCCUAGAUUUCCUUUUCUCCACGUGCUUAUUACCUUCUAAUAUACCAUAUGAUUUACCUACUAAUUACAUUUAUCUUGCUUCCUCCCGAAAACAUAAGCUCCAUGAAAACACGACUUUGUGCCUGUUAUGGUCUCUUUAAUAUCACCACUGUUUAGAAUAGUGCCUUGCCUCUAUAGCUUGGACACCUUUUCCCUCUACUUAGAUUUCCCUUCCCUGAACUCCAUGUAUGUAAAUCCUACCUGUUUGCCAAGGCUUAGCUUCAGUGCUAUCUCAGCUGAAAAACUCCCCCACUCCUCUGAACUUGGGUGAAGAUCAUUUCUUCUUCUCUGAACAUUGGCAUCAUUUAACCAGAAACUGCUUUUAUAUUGUUGAAAAACUGUUUUCUUGCUUGUAUUUGGCUAUUUAUGUGCAUUUCUUAUCUCUCCCACAACCAUGCCUUAAAAAUAGGUUUCACCACUAGCUCAUCUUUACAAUUUUAGUAGUACUUAGUACUCCAUGUAUGUAGUAAAUGCUUGACAAAUAUGUGUUGAAUAAUAGCAGCAUGAAUAUGCUUACACAGAACUUUCUAAAGAAAUAUAUGAACAAGAUUCUUGAAUUAUGCAAAACCCAUGUGAAAAGGUAUUUUGAUUUUUGAGCUUGAUUAUUUUCGGGGAAAAUCCAAUUAUGUCUUAAACUUAAUGGAGUGAAAAUAUCCAAUAAGAAAAAAAAUGUAUUUGAAAUCUUUCAUUUUAUAUUCAGAACCCAGACUAUGUCCUAUCGAUAUCUUUUUUACAUCAGAGUAAUUUCCUUCUUUCAAAGCAUUUGUGCCAUACAAAUUGUUUAUUCACAAACUAAUGUCAUGUCCAGCUACCCGAAAUGGUUUGUAAUUUAAUUAAGGAAAAUAUAAUUAAAGACACAAAUAACAUAGGAUUUAUAUCAAGCAGUAAAUGUAGAUUUGCUGUCACUUGGGUUUUACACUUUUUCAUAGUGUAUGUCUUGGCAUUAAUGAAUCACCUUAUAUUAAACAGAAUUGGGAGCGAUAAUAGGACUGCGCUCAUAAGACAGAAGACUGAAAGCAAUUUGAUGAGGAUCUUAUCCUUCUUUCCUUUUUAUGGAAUUCCAGAAAAAACCUCUAUCACUGGAUUAUAGUUGAUUUCAAAAGUUUCUUUUACAGUCAUUUUCCUUAUAUCCAUGGCCAAUUACCAAACUAAAAAUGGCUCCCUCUGUUCUAUAUGAAAGUUUCAUAAUUCCAAAGUUCAAUAUUCAUCACUAAGUCCUCAACGAGGGAAGAUUUGAAUACUUGUUUUAAGAAAGUUUUUUUUUUUUUUAAAUCCUCAAGGUAAAAGUAUUUUCAAAGUAAUCAAACCUGGGCUUACUCAGUGGAAAAGUGGUAAUUAGUAUGGUCUCUUUUGUGAAGCUGGUUAAAAGCUGAUGUUAAAAGAAAUUAUAACUCUGAUAGAAUUAUGCUCAAAGUGUUAAGUGAAUGUGUCUCAGAGAAUCAUUGAUAUUGAGUGCAUAUAGUACCACAGAAUUCUGAAGUUAUGUCAGUGGAGUAGCCAUAUGGUGGUAUGUAAUAAAAUGUAGUUUCCAAACUCUUCACGUAGAAACUUACAGUCUUGGCUCACACCAGGAGCCCCCUCCCUUUCCACCUGUCCCAUGAAAGCCUUUGGCAGGAAAACAGGCCCUGUGCUAACUCCCAGGGACACAUAUUCAUGCUUGUUUUCUUCAGUUCUGUGCCCAACCUCACUCAGUCACCACGGAUGCAGCUUUGAGUAAAACAGACCAAACCUUCUAGUGAGAUCAGGGCUGGUAUGACAGGGAGAGAUUCUGCGUUAGUUGAGCAGCUCCUAGGAGAGUGGACUACUCUCCCUUGAUUCUUAAACUUACUGAGGAGCAGUAUUAGGAUAUUUUACCAGCACAAAAUUAGAUAUCCCUUAACUUCCUUUAUUUGAUUUUUUUUUUCUGGUUUAGUCGACUAUGCUUGCAAUUGGUAACCUCUUGUUAAUGGAUUCUGUUUCUAAGGGUUUUAUCACCUCAUCUGAUACCUAAAAUGUCUGGAGCACAAUGACAUUCAAUAAAUAUUUAUUGUGUCUAUGAACAAACAUGAAUAAAUGAUUCAAAUAAUGCAUUUCUUAUAUGACUCUUUCCACUGGUUUAGAUAAAAACCAAAGAUCUUUGGUAGUAGAAUUAUACUAUUUUUAGGUUCAGCUCAUGCCUUAUGGGAUCACUAUAUAAAACCGCAUUAUUUAAUCCCUUUUGAGAGAAAUCAAUAGUACCAGGUCAGUAUUAUAAAGAUAGCUUAUUUGCAUUGCUACCACCUUGCCAAUUGCACAAGCCACGAGAAUUCUGAAAAUUAGGAAAACUGCCCAAUUUAAGCAUAGUGAAUAUUAUCAUCAACCUGGCGCUGACCUGGCUGGCUGUGAUGCGUAUGUGCACUUGGUAUAUUUCCUCUGAUCUAUCAUUUGGACUCCCUUUUUGACAAUUUGAAGGUCUUAGAAAUUGAUUAGUGGUCUUUAAACCACAGUGAUCAACAGUGGCAAAAUAAAACACAAUAAUAGUUAUUUCAUCUUUUAUUGUAAUCAGGAAAAAUUAGAUAUUUCCAUGCCAGAUUAUAGUUUAUGCAUUUAAGUGUUCUUAUUUUUCCUUAGUGAAAGUGGAGAGAAUUGGGGGUGGGAAGCACAUAAUUAAUAUGCUUUGUAAAAAAAACUAGAAAACUCUCAGACUAAAUCAAAACCUGAUACCUGUAUAAAACAUUAAAACCUGUACUUUGGAACAAUGUGCUUUAAAAACAAAUUGAGGUGCUAGUGGCAUGGAAGAAAGUCCAAAUGCAAAUGAUGAGGAGACAGCUAUGAAAUGUAGGUUGGUUGGCUGCAGUUCUGCCCAUGAAGCACUAGCUGGCAUUAGUAUGAAAUUUAAAUUCACUUCUGUGCUGGUGAUUGCCUCUUUGGAACUCAUUAAACAUUCUUUGGCAUCAGAUUUUAGACUGAGUAAAGCCAUAGAGCAUGAUCCAGGCAGAAAUUAACCUCAGGGCCUAUAAGCUCCUGUAACUGAGCAGCUAAGAAGUUGAUGUUCUGUCCCGGAAUAAGAUUCUCAGAAAGGGUGGAGCUUGAGAGGGAGCUUAGAGUUCAAAUCUCACAGCUGGAAAUCAAGCCAAGAGCAGUGUAUUUGACUUCGUUAGUAUUACUGCUCUUUUGGUUUGUAUGCUAAUCUUUUGAGCUUCAUCAUUUCAGUUUCUGCCUGAGAGCUGGCUCUUCAAAAACUUUAAGUGAAAUGACAGUCUACAAAAUUGCUCUUUGAGAACAAUUAAACAAAGUCAGGAGGCAUGCAAUAUUUUUAGCAAUGGGUAAAAGGGAUCAUUUAAUUAUGACAAAGUGAAGCUCAUAGUCUUCAGAAUUGUUUCGACAGAUCUGAUUGUUAUGUGACAAGUUUUGGAUGGUGGCUGGUUUCUACAGCCUAGCUGAGCUCAGAUGGUAUAUAGAGGAAAUAUUGCCAAGAUAAUGAAUGAGAACUUAGGAGCUAUACGGAAUUACUCCUGACAAGACAGUAUUUUCUUUCUGUUCAACAGGUGACUGCAGAAGAGAUCCAUUGAAAAAUUACAUUAACUGAUACCACUAUCAACUCAUAAAGCAGGAUAGGGAGAGUAAGACAAUACUCAAAGAAAAGAUGCCUAGAAUACCAAGCAAAUGAUUUUCUGAGUAUCCCAGUAAUGUUGUAUUCACUUCUUGAAAUAAGGGAAAUAGUAAGUGGUCAUUAAUAAAAUAAGAUAAGAAGUGAUAUCUUUAAUUAAAUGGGCAACUUGUUCUUAUUACAGCUGUUCUGACUGAUUAUGAUUAACUGCCAAUUCUGAGACUUGACUCAUUAAUUCUUCAGUGUACAGGACUUAGGAGCAGAAUAUUGCAUGAGACACAACUUACCAAAUCCUCUGGAAAUAACGUUGUUGUUGUUUUUUUUUUUAAAUCAAGAUCAACUAUAUUUCAAUUAUUAGAAAGCACACACCUUGACCACCUUGACAUGUGGAGAGAACAACACACAGAUUUGGAGUAGCUAUGAUGCAAAUCAGGAUAGUAGAGUUGGGAACAGAAAGCUUGCCUCAUAUUGAAGGACCAGCAGGAGUUGGGCCUCUGCUCUCACCUCUCAUUGAAUCUUUUCACUGGUACUGUGGGAAAUGCACAGGCCUUGCAAUCAAACUGCAGAGGUUCAAAUCUGAGCUCUACCGCUUAGCAGCUGUGGGCAUUGUGGUACAUUUUUCAUUCCAGUUGAGACUUAUUUUAUAUGUAAAAUGAGGCUGAAAUAACAAACCAAUAGGAUUGUUAUGAAGUAUGCAUGAGAAGAAAAAAGCACAGGAUUAAAGUUCUGGAGUCAGAUAGUCUGGGUUGUAAUCUUGGCUCAAAUGUUUAUAAGUUGGUUGACUUGGUGCCUUUGUUUUCUUGGGUAAAAUGCAGAAGUUCUCUUGGUCCUGUGCUGUAGCGUUGAAUAAUCGUGUUAAUGUUUGUUAGGCACCAGAGCCAUCCUGGUACAUAGUCAGCUCUAACUAUUAUUACAAACAGGACCUGGGAAAAUACUUAACAUAUUGUAAAUUCUCAAUAAAAGGAAGCUGUUGUGAUUACUGUGGUUUGUUUCUGCUAUUAGUUCCUAUCCGGAAGCACUAUGUUCUUGAUUUUUGCAUGUCUAUUUUUUCUAUUUAGCCUAUAUGACUAAAUUGUCUGUAAGUUUUAAAACCAAAUCACUGCUAAAGUUUAAAAGUGAAGGCAGGAGUAUUGUCCUCCUUGCAUACUGUGAUAUUAAUCCAAAACAGUACUUAAAAUAAAAAUUUACCUAUUAAGCACAAAUCUAUAAGUAGAAGAGAUUUUUUUUCCUUCACUUCAUAGAAUUAGACUCAUGCAAAGUUCCCAGCAGUCACAACUUCAUACAAACCACAACGAGAAACAAGGUACCAAAUUAAAUGAGAUACGUUUUUUUGUUAGUGGGACUAGCAGGGAAUGAAGAAACCAAUACUAUGUUUUAAUAUUUAAACAAUUAAAUUCAUAUUCCAUAAGAUGAAUCAACCAGAUUAAUAAGAAAAUUUGCAAAUGAAACUAAAUGUGGAAUUCCUGGAAAAUGCCAGUAAAAACAGAAAUUAGCCAGUGAGGUAAGAAGUUAAAAAUGAGAUAAACAAAAAAAUUCAAAUGGGAUGAAAACUAAUGAUACUAAACAAGGAUGAUAUUGCUAUUCAAAUAAGAUAAAGUUUAAUGGUGACUAUUUUUUCUUUAUAAAAUUAGCGUGGAAAAAAUUUGACUCAUUCAUAAAGAAAUUCUAUGACGAAAGAGGAUAUCAAUGGGUUUUUUGACCUCUUGAAAAUAUAUCUUUAUUGUUUUUACCUACUCAUGUUAAAAAAAUACAUACAUAAAUGUAUGGUGAUUUAAAAGACAAAAAGAAAAUUAAAUUUUAGCAUUUCUUCUCUUUAUGUAAAGUAAUUUUCUAACAUUUCAAGUUAAAGAAGGCUCAUGCUCUUUAGAUUGACAAAAAUAAAUACUCAUACACAAAAAGUAGAUUAAAAAGAAUGUGUGAUCAAAGAGGAAGUUAGGGGCUUCAAAGUUUCAGAUAGAAGGUUAGACUUUUCAGACAGAAGGAAAAAAAAUGGAAUGGUAAGAAGGCCUUCCCAGAAAUGGUUCAUUGGAAUAGAGAACUGUUCAGUAUGGAGAUUAAAAAUGGAAAAACAGAUUUCCUUCACAUUGUCUUUCAGAGGCUGAUGAGUCUUUGAAAAACAGAAUUGUUCACCUAUGCUUAUAAAGCCUUUUGGUGCAUGACCAUGCCUGUAGACACCUCUCCAUUUUUUCAUUUAACAAAUAUGGAUUUAUGCUUAGUAUGUGACAGAUAUUAUAUUACAGUCUAAAGACACAAAGAAAAAUAAUACCUGUCAUCAAGGAGGUUACAGUCCAGUAGAAGAAAUGGGCAUGCAAAAAUAAAGAAUUAGAUCUCAUAAUUGGAGUACUAGAAGUGCAAAAUGUACUGCAGGCACAAAAGAAAGAACACUUAACCCUUUCUGGCUGUACCAGGGAAGAUAUUAAAAGGUGUGUCUUGAACAAGGAAGGUUCUUUUUUUGGUGAAAUGCUUUGCAUUUUUAUUGUACGAUUCAUUGUCUCAUUAGCUAAACCAUUUAGCACUUGUGUAGUGCUUCACAGAUUACAAAGUGCCUUCAGACACAUUAAACAUAAAGUACAUUUUAUUAAACAGUAGUUCCUUUUUAGGCAUUUUGAUUGCAGCUUAUUGAUUUUGUCUUUAUAGGCACUAGACCUAUAUCUCUAUAGGGUUCUAGUAGAGGAGGGGAUGUUCUAGUUACUAUUCCUGCAUAACAAAUCACUUCAAAACAUAAUGAUUUAAAACAGCGAUAAUCAUUUCAUUAUUUCUCAUAAUUUCUGUGGGUCAAGAUUUUGAGAAGCACUUGGCUGGAUAAUUCAGACUCAUGAUCACUCACACAGUUGUGGUCCCACUGACUGGAGCUAGGACAAGAGAGGGCUGGAGCAGCAUGGGCUGGCUGAGAAUCUCUUUGUCUGCAUGUUGUGUUAGGGCUUCUCCAUGUGGUCUGACCACAUGGGUUAGUUUGGUCAGAGGCCACCAUGCUGUGGGGAAGCCCAAUCAGACUACUUGCAUCCUGGGUCAGGGUCCCUUACCAGCAAGGUGGAAGCUGAAUCGAUUUUUCUAGCCUUAUUUUGGAAGUCACACUGCAUCAGUUGAGUCACUAUCUAUUGGUCACAAGCAAGCUACAAAUUUAAGAGGAAGGGAACUAGAUUUAACUUCUUGAUGGAUGAGAGGCAAGGUUCUAGAAGAACAUUUGAGAUAGGGGAUUUUCUUGUGGGCAUCUUUGGAAAAUACAUCUUUACAUCUUCAUUCAAGCUUUGAGUAAAUAAAUUAUUCUUCUUUUAACAAAGAUGGCAUGGGAUCUUAUCAGAAAAUUAUCCAAGCCAGAGGGAAAUUACUAAAUUUUACCUGUUUUUAAACUGAGUUUUAAAAUUUCAGUACCUGCCACUUUCUAACAAAACAGAUAAAAACACGAUAGGAUAGAUAAGAAGAAAUUAAUUUGGCAAGGAGGAAGGAUUUUCUGACAUGCUUAGCCAUUGACCCUUAGAAGAGGUUACCACAGGAAACAGAAGAAUCAGUUUCUCUGGAGGUUAAAAACUGAUGGUAGAGGAAUUCUGUGAAUCUCACUUGUUGUCAGUGUAGUCCCAGCUGGAGGAAAGAGAGAGAUUGGUAACCUUUUUAGGCCUAUUCUUCUGAAUUCACAAGGUAUAGAGAGAUUGUCUGGGUAACCUUGGAAAGGUCUUUUGGUCAAUUAAAAGGCUUGUUUUUAUAUUAUGUAUUUAUUUCUUUAUCAUUCAUUCUUUAUUUUGAGCACUAUGUUUCAUAAAAAAAAGUUCCAAUUUUCUACAUGUACGGUUCUACCCAAUGCAAUUACCAAAAGGGCUUUCCAGAUCCUGAUUACUGUCCUUUGAUAAUAACUAGAUAACUAGAUGAUUAAUUUCUAGUUAUUAAUCAAAGGACAGUAAUCAGGAUUAUUAGGAUAAUUAUCCUUCGUGAUAACUUAUAAUUUAAGGCAUUUUUUUGGCAUGACUGACAAGGCAAGUAACAGAUUAUCUAUGGAUGAUAGUUUUGUGUUUAUAAGUGCAUUGGUAUCUAUAUGUAUAGGUCGUCAUAUAGAGAGGUUAAGUGGUACCAAAUAUUUUGCUUUACUUGCAUUAUUUGAUUUGAUUUUAAACAACUCUAGUAUAGUUAGUAUCCCUAUUUCACAGUUGAUAUAAAUAAGGCAGACAGAAGUUAAGUAACUUGUCCAAAGUAAAGAGGCAAAGCUAAGAUUUAAUCAAAUUCCACUAACUCUAGAGCCUCACUGCUGAACAAGGUACUGUACUAUUUAUUAUUAACAGUGAAAUGAGUACUCAAUCUUCCUUUCUAAGUUUCUACUGUAUUUUCAAAUAAGUCUGCAGUCUGGAAUUUAUAAAUCAGAAUCCCUCAAUGUCAUUAAAGUAUAGGCCAGAUGCUCCUUUAUCUGGUAUGCAAGGCCUUUUAUGAUCUAACCCCCCUCCCGUGUGUGUGUGUGUGUGUGUGUGUGUGUGUGUGUGUGUGUGUGUGUGUGUGUUUCAACUUUUUUCUUCUAUUCCUCCAAAACAGGCCUCUCUGUUUUGUUCUAGCCAAAUGGGUAGUUCUCAUGCUGUUUCUUCUACCAGACACUGUCACCUCACUCUCAUUACGUUCUUUCUAGUAUUUAAACCUGUUUGAAAGCUGUCUCUUCUAUGAAGCUUCUUAGAUUACCCAACAAGAAGAUAUUUCAUGAGAAUUCCUAUAGCUCUUACUUCCUGUAUGACUUGUGAGAAAUUUGUCAAUGUUAUAAUUGCUGUUUAUGUGUAUAGAAUCUCCCCAAUCAAGUUAAAAACUCCCGGAUGGAAAAAAAAUGGCUGCAUUCUUUGCUUUUUUUCUAUCUUCAAAUCCUGGCACAGUGUGCCACAAAUCUACACUUUUUUCGAUGUUGAUUAAGUAGUCUAACUUCCUUGUAACCAAUUUCUGUCUGAAUUGGGCGGCAUCAUUCUCUAUUUCCAAGGCCUGUUCUUGAGAAUAAUAUUCUUCUCAGGUUUAAAAUAAUAUUAUAAUAAUUAUGUGACUAAAAACUUUUGAGAAAAUGUUGCUAUUAGCAUGGGGGUGCUUUCUUUGUUUGCUUUCACAUAUCCUUAUUCAGUAUACAUUUUAAUGACUCUAGGAUGCUCAUUCUGUCAGAUAAAGAACAUAAUUAGGUAUACUUUGUUUACACAAUUGAGCAAAAAGAGUCUGGUCUGAAUUACUUAAUUGACUGGUCUCUAGUAUCAGUGAUGCUAAAAACUGAACUGAAUUUCUGAGCAUAAUUCCCUAGCUGCUUGUGCUUUUUUCUAGGACUAUAGAUUGCACACCUAAAACUGGACAGUCAUCUGACAUAACUGUGCUGUUAUUUAAUGAGACAAUCAGACAGUACAAGUACCAUCGCUUCUGUAUACGAAGGAAGAUAAUACUGCGAUUAAAGAUUUUGAAUGUUAGUCCUAGAACUCAAAACUUGACUCACAUCCCAUUUCUGUUACUAUUUAGCAAACAAGAUUAAACUAUUGUCCAUUUACUGAUAACCUACUUUGCUGUAAAAAAGAUUUUAACAAUUUUAUAAAUAUAUCAAGGUAUGUACUGUAACAAGAAAACAUCAAUUUUAACCAAAUGGCAAAGAUGAGGUUAGGUGAUAACAAGGAUAAGGGAAUAAAAGAGACCCCAGAAUAAGGCCAGUAAUAGAGAUAGAUGUCAGGUUAUCAUACAAUAUUUGUUUUUUGUUUUUUUUUUUUUAGACAGAGUCUGGCUCUGUCACCCAGGCUGGAGUGCAGUGGCGCGAUCUCGGCUCACUGCAAGCUCCACCUCCCGGGUUCACGCCAUUCUCCUGCCUCAGCCUCCCGAGUAGCUGGGACUACAGGCGCCCGCCACCACGCCCAGCUAAUUUUUUGUAUUCUUUUUAGUAGAAACGGGGUUUCACCGUGUUAGCCAGGAUGGUCUUGAUCUCCUGACGUCGUGAUCCGCCCGCCUCGGCCUCCCAAAGUGCUGGGAUUACAGGCGUGAGCCACCGCGCCUGGCCAGGUUAUCAUACACGCUUACUAAGAGUGGGCUGCACAUUUCACUCUGCUUACCGACGUGAAGAGGGAAACCCGUUCAAGUUCAUUGUCAGUUUUACUGAUUUGCGGCGCCUAUUAAAAACAAACCAUUUGCCGAGGAGGUGUGCGCCUACGUAGAGAACUAAGAAAUUGCUUUCACGAGGCUUUAAGAAGAAAACACCGUUUAAGCCCUAGGAAUGAUUCUGGGUAAUAAUUAUAAGCCAAUAGAAGCUUUUUCAACUAAAGAAUUUUAAAGAUAAAUUAAUACUAUUUUUGUUAGAGGUAGUGAUUUUGCUUUCUGUCAUGUGCUCGUGUUUCCUACAUGGGCAACUUAUGACUUCUCUGUUGAUCUAUCUGGUUUCACAGUGCUAAUCUUCUCCAAAACUCCAGAAAAAUCUCUCAUUUCAGUAGUGGCACCUCGUUCUAUCACCACAUUCUCAAUUCUACCAUUGCCUUCAGAAUGGCACUUAAAACAUUGGCCAGCUUGCCUUAUCUUUGUUUCUAAGUUUCUAUCACGCUGCCAGCUACCUACCCGCAACCCCAACUGCUCUGCAUUCCUAUAUUCAAGUUCGGUGUUUGACGACCUUUGGCCAGAGAUGUUUUUUGCCAUGGAUUUGGGGCUGUAGAAAUGGCUAAAAGAAAGCUCUCCCCUCAACUGAAACAUAGCAGCUCGACUUUUCUCUGUUUUGUUGAUUAUAAUUCCAUAUAUAAAUUCACUGAGGGGGAAAAAAGCAUUCACCUGCCUUUAAAAAAUUAAUACUUGAAAACAAUCAAUGCUCUCUGAAGUCCCUUUGAGGUGUAGACACUGAAAAUGAGAUCAGCUAAACUGAGUAUCUCUUUUCAUGCAUUGUCCAAAUUAGUUUUCUGUUUCCUAGAUUCUCUAUGUUUGUGCUACCUAAAUUUAUUCUUGCUUUGAGCUGUAAGCACAUGCAGUAAGUAUUUUAAUGAGUUAUGUAUCUAUAUUUUUCUUUUUCUUAUGUAGUUUCUUCUUUCUUAUUUACUCACUUUGGCUGCCAUGCUACAGAUUUCUUCACCCUUUCUUUUUAUUCUUCCCCCAAAAGAAAUACAUGAUCUUCCAUCUAAAGGACAAUCGUUUGUAAGCCAUAUGAGACAUUCUUCAACAACACAUUUCACACAUUUAUUUUAUUCUCAAUAUUGAAGUUGAGCCAUCCUUUUUUCAUCAUGAACAUCCUCCUUUAGAGUUCACUGGGUAUGAAGCUGGAGCAACUGCUAAUAAAUUCAUUACACCAUCCUUAAUCAUACCAAUAUCAUAAAAUGCACCCUUUGAAAUAUAAUAUUAGCCUGCAGUUUUAUUGUGGCAGGAAAGACUAAUGAUUUGUUAGCAAACUAAGCAGAAAGAUAUCUUGACAAUGGAAAAUAAAGGGCAUCAAUACCAUAAUGUGACUUGUUUAGGAAGUCAAAUGUUUUUACCUGAAAUAACAUAAAUUACCCUAAAUUAGAAUUAUAUCUGUAGAAAUAAAAUUAAGUGCCUGUAUUACCAGAAAAAAAAGUCUUAAAAUAUUACAUCAAAAAGUAAAAGAACAGAUUUUCAGGCUAUGACAAUUCUUAAUUUAAUUGAACAGAUUCUUAAAGCAUGAAUCACUUUUCCUCUAAUACUACAUCCCCAGUCUUUCAAGAAAACUUGCAGGUACAUGGAGGAAAUUGCUUCAGCCCUCUGUGACUUAAAUAAUAGUCAUAAAUGUGACUUAAAGUAUCUUAAUAUGAGAUAUGCAUAUAUUAUAUAGUUUAUGAAAGUCUGAAAUUAAUUUACAAUAAUAAUAAACUUAUGGUACCAAAGCUUUUUUCUGUUAGAGAAUAAUUCCUCUAUUUUUUGGAAAUUUCAAUCUCUGAAAUUUAUUUGUAAUGAAAUGUAUUGCAGUUAAGUGGGAAAGGCAUGGCCUUUGGGUCAGAGUAAGCAGGGUUUUAAUAUUUUCUCCUUACCACUAAGUGAUAGCCAUUCUCAAAUGUUUUGGUUUCAGGUGCACUAUUAAAAAUUAUGAGGACCCCAAAAAUAUUUUUUUAAAUGUGGGUCAUAUCUGUUAAUACUUACUAUGUUUGAAAUUAAAACUCAACUACUUUAGAAAUAUUUAUUCAUUUACAAUAACAAGCCAUAAAAAAACAAUUUUUAUGAGACAUAACUAUAUUUUCCAAAACAAAAAAUAGUAAAAAGAAUGUAUUAUUUUAUAUUUUUUGCAAACUUAUUUAAUUUCUGGCUUCAUAGAAGACAGCUGGAUUCUCAUAUCUCUUUCUACAUUCAGUCUGUUGCAAUAUGUUAUAUUGGUUGAAGUAUAUGAAGAAAAUCUGCCUGACACAGAUAUGCAGUUGGAAAAGGAAGGAGUAUUUUAAUACCUUUUUAAGUAAUUGUGAAUAUUCUUUAAUGCUACACCAAAACUUUGAUUAGUGGUAGUUUCUUAAAGGUUAGUUGCAAUGUAGAAUCGAAAACCAUAUCAAUGAACCUUUAUUUUUUGUACUCAGUUAAAUUUAAUUCCAAUGGUGUAUCUUGCAUUUUGAAUGAAUCUUUUUUGCAUGCACGAGUUUGUAACAUCAUGCAUUGCUCAUUGUUUCACUGAAUUAUGCCAAUCUUUCUAAUGUUGACACAUUUAUAACAGUUACCUCUUUAAUUUUGCCACUCUUUUCCUCAGAGAAGAUUUUAUAUAUUGGGAAGCUUAUCAAAUGGGCAGUGGCAGAUAAAAGUUUCCCCAAAUUAUAAUUUAGCUCUAAAGCUCAAAUUUUAUUGGUAACAAUCACUGUCAAUUGUUUUCUUUGAAAUGUCAGGUUUACUUUAUCUUCAAGAAAAUGUCUGCCAAAUACUCAAGUCUGAAUAGCCAUAGUUUAUCUGUCAGUCAUUCAUUCAAGUAAAAACAGUACUUCAUGCACAAAGUGUCUAGUUCAGCUUGCAACUCAAACAAUUGCACAGGUGCUUUCACAAACAUCAUAUUUAGGUAUGAAGUAAGUUACUUGCAUUUUUCAUUUUGUCACAUGGAAUAUUAAAAAGAUAUAUAAUCAAGAAUUAUGAUUUAACAUUUUUUUUACUGUUUGGUCAGGGACAUUCUUAAAAGACUUCGACACUCUGACACUCCCCCCACCCCCAGUUUUCUGGCAGUGUACUGUUAGCACAGCUGAUGCUGCCACUGCCUUGAUUUGUGAUAAGGUACCAGCAGUUAUACUUGCCACUGCUUCUGUACCAGCAUGCAAAUAUCAACAUAGAAAAGGGAGGACAAUAAAGUAUUAGUAUUAAUACUAUUAUGAAAUUGAUUUUGACCUAAUGAGCCCUCUUCAGGUUCUUAGGGACCCUCAGGGGUCUACACACUACAUGUUAAGAACAUCUAUUCUAGGGUUAUGACCUCUUUAAGAUUGUUGCCUCACUAAUGAAAAUAAGAAUAAUGAUAUAUGCAUUGCAUAUUGUUUGGACAUUUAAGUCUGGAAGUAUGGUUCUUAAAAAUGUAAGUUUCUGUUCCUUGUUUUCCAAAUAUUAACCUCUGAACAAAGCCAGUAUUUCUUCAGGCAGAGCGUCGCUAAAGUAAUGUUAGUUAUUCUUACGUUUAGAAUAUGAAUCUAAUCUGUUAAAAUAUAUCUCUAAGUUUCUUUUAUAGAAAAAAACUGUUAUUAGAUACUCUCUGGAAAACUAAUUGGUGUAUUUUCUCACUUUGGAAGAAUUUCAGGAAGUGUAUUUAGAGUACCAAUUUAACUGAAUAUGUGAUUCUUUUCAGGUAUUGGUACAUUUGAUAUUCAUUGGUUAUGUGAGAUGGUUUAUCAAUAUGUGAUCUUAUCUCUCUUUGUGCUUAUUCAUGAAUUCGUAUAAUAUUUCACGUCUUCUUCCUAUUAGAUCUUGAGCAUCUUGACUCAAAAAUGUGUUUUCAGAACAUCACUUAGUACACAGUACUUGAUCAAUAAUGAUUGUUAUGUUUAUAAGGAACCUAUUUCCUCCCUAUUACCUCACACACAUUCGGUCUACUUUCUUGUACAAAUUGUUGGUUGUAUACACUAGAAAGACAAAAUUUCUAAUAUUAAGCUAAGUGAAAUGGUGUUUUAAAAGUAAAUCUAUUAGAUUGGUGCACAUAUGUGCAUUUAUAGUAUGGUUUAGGUAUGGGACCUAUAAACCCUUGAGGCUGCUCUCCUCCAUUUCAGAUAAUCAGAUUAAACAUUUUAAAGGAAAAUAAAUCAGAACUCAUUUAGGUUUAUUUAAAUUUAUUAAAAGUUCACCUAACACACAAAGGCACUCAUCAGUGACAAUAUGUUUUGCAAAGAUUUGUUCUAUAAGAGUGUGAGUCAUCCAAAAUUGUAGUCAUCUCUGUUGGAUAAUUUGGAAGCAUUAUUUCUAAGAUGGAACAAGGAAAACCAAUGCCAAUGUUCUAAUAAGUUGCUCAGUGGUUGAAUGGUUUUUAGAAAGUAUAUUAAUGAAAGUAUUGCAUGAAAUAUUUGAAAAGGACAACUUAGUAAAUUUAUUUUUUCCUAUCUCAUAGUCCAGUUAGCUGUUACUGUUGUUGUAUCCUGGAAUAGGACAUAAAACUUCUGGGAAGAUCUGUAGACACCCAUUUCUAUGAAAGUCCUUCAGGGUUGUCUGUAUGUGAGGCCAUCAAAUAAUGCAGUGACUUGUCUUUCUCUUACAAGGUAAAACAAAGAAAUAUAAGGUCUUCUGAUAUACAUUAUAAUGUAAUUUUUCUACCAUAUUAAAAAUAUCAGUAAAAAAAUGGCAGAACUACUGGGCAAUCUGUACACACAUGGAAAGAUAAGAAUUUGUCAAUAAUUUUCAAAAUAGGCAGUGGAAGUGCAAGAUGUUUCAUGUAUUGUAGAUUUAGAUAGUCUUUACAAAAAGCCAAUUUAAAAAAUUUACCACCUACUUAUACGUAACGAAACUCGACACAGAAAAGUUAUGUAUCAGUUAGAUUUUGCUGCUCUGUAACAGACAAUCACAAAAAUCUCAGUGGCAUACAACAAAGAACAUUUGUUUCUCAUAUGUGUGCAGGGUUCACUGAACUAGGCUGGGCUUAGUUCAGUGGUUUCGCUGAUCUCUCCUGGGAUCACUCACUGACCUCAGGAUGACCACAGGCUCUGUGCUAGGCUGGGCUUGGUUGGCAUCCCUUAGCUUUGACAGAUCUGCCCCCACGUGUUUUUCAUCCUUUUCCUGGGACCAACAGUCUAGUCUGGGCAUGUUCUUCUCAUGGCAAUGGCAAAAGUGCAAGAAGGAAAGCGGAAACAUACAAGACCUCUUGAGGUCUAUGUUUGUCACUGUUAUGCUGUCACUUCUGAUUUGUCCUGUUGUCUGAAGCGGGUCACAUAGGGUGGUCAAAUGUACUUUGCUCUUACAGGAAGUACUCAAAAUUCACUUGACAAAGGAAUGACUACAGAGGGGGUGAAUUAUUGAGGCCAUAAAUGCAAUUAAUAUUCCACACUGUAUUGCCUUGGGUCCUAUAAAUAGUGGCUCACUGAGGUAGGUCAAGAACAUAAGCCUCUUUAGGCAACUGCUUUCUCAGUGGUUCCUUAGGCAGGUUUUAGUGCUUCCUUCUAAUUUGGUCCAUUCAGAGGCUUUUGAGUGGUAUUGAAUGGCUGCAUUUAUAUUCUAGUUUCUACCUAUUACAAAAAUAAAGGAAAAUAGAUUCAGAUGAUGGUACCAACUUCCAUUUGCCUCUGUGCAGCUGCAGUGAUCACAUGCUGCUAUAUUUGAUGCCUGUAUUGAGAGAAAUAGAGAAAAAUCAUAAUCUGUCAAACAUAAUUUGUUGUCUUUGUCUUAUUGCAUCUGAUUGCUUUGUCCAAAUUCUCAUUCAUAAGCAACAUAUGAUAUCAUCUAUUGUCGUUCUUAGAUGAUAUGAGGAAAAUAGGUUCAAUCCAUAUAGUUGUUAUGUUUACGAUUAUGCAUUUUACAUUUACUGAGACAGUAUAUUAAUUUAGACUACAAAUACUAUUGUUCUUUGCUAUUUUGUUGCUUAUCAGUCAAUUACCGUUUUCAGAUAUGUGACCAUUACAGUUGGGGCAUUGUAUUAAAUACAAAUAUUUUAUUUCCUCUUGUUUUAAGAAUGCUCCUUUAUACCUGCACUUCACUUAUAUUAGUGGUAAGAAAUUGAUCUUAUAGUCACAAAUACUGAGUUUAUUCCUUAAAGGCAUGAAUGUCUUACUGAUGGCUUGACAUUAUAACACAAUAUAAAGAUUUUGCUGUCUGAUUUCCUACAGACAAGUAUAACACAACAUUAUUUGGACAAAACCCUUACUAGAAUGUAAAUGCUGUAUGUAUUAUUUUAGGAUACUUUUAAUACUUCUCUGCAUUUUUCUUAAAAUAAAUUAUUGAUUUCACUGAAUUUAUUUAACCGGAAAAUAACAUGGAACUCAGAAAGAGAAUUUUACUAGAAUGAUUCUAUUACAAUAUUUUUGCUGUUAAUAUGUAUUUAAGAGGCUCAGGUGAAGCAAUUAUGGCUAAGUGUGUAUGUGUCCACACAAUUGUAAAUAUUUUUAACAACAUACAUCUCUUGUUCACAUGCAUUAUAAAAUCAAACUGCCCCCAAAAUUUUCUCCUCUCCUGCUUCUCUCCUAGGAGUAGGACAAGACAGUAUUGGGAAAUCAUUUGGCUAGUGAAGUAGAAUAAGGCCCCACUCCCUGAUAUAUUCUACGAUAUUUUGCAGUUAUUUAUGUUAGUAAGAACUAGUAAAGGCUUUUAUAGUAAUUGCCUGUGAGAAGAAAUCUGCUUGUGUUACUAAAGAUUUUGCUAUGUGGAUUGCUGAGUUUCCUCAUGAACCUCACAUGUACUCUGUACCUUUUCCUUCACCCCAAUUUAAUCUUCUAUUUUGAGAAUUUAUUAUUAUGUUUUUAAAGCUCUAAUCCUGUUGCGCCAUUUCCUUGCACAGCCCCUUAAGGCUCUUACUCCUCCUCUACCUGGUUACCUUCAAAGAGAAAGUCUGAUUCCUAGAAUAAACAGUCCCACAUCAACUUUGCAAAGCUCUUCCCUUAUCAGUCUCCAACAACAAUCCUCUGCUCCAGCAGUCCAGUUUAUGGUGGUCUGAUUUCUAAAUCCUUUAUUAAAGGUGUUGUUACUUUACACCCUAAAAAACUCCAUAGAAAAUUUUAAAAUACAAAAAAUCCACAAAUAAAAACAUCACCUAUGAUUCUACCUCAGCUAUAUAAUCAUUGCCAUCUACUUGGAGUAUUUCUUCUGCAAAAUUUUCAUUUCUUCAUUGUACUUUUCCCAAAAUUUUUAUCAUAAACCCUUUUAAACAUCUUGAAAAUUUGGAAGAAUUUUACAAUAAACAUUUGUAUACUCAGAUUCUACCACUCACAUUUUACUAUAUUUGCUUUAUCACAUAUCCAAAAUACAUCACUCCUAUAUUCUUCUUUCAAUCCAUCCUAUUUCUGGUGCAUUUCAAAGUAAAUUGCAGAUUUAGUAUGUGUAAUUACAGAGCAGUUACGAGUUAGUUAAAAGUUCUAGAUGAGAUGAGGAGACCCAUCACAAAAGGGACACAAUCUAUCUGAUAUCAUAGGCUUUCCUAGAUAGUACCAAUGCUUCCAUAAAUAUACUUAAGGUGUCAGACUAUAUGUCCUGAUUUUUAGUUUGGAAAUCUGUCCUCAUAGGACAUAUCUGGGGCUCAGAGUCUUCAAAAACUAGGUGAUGAAAUAUAGGCCAUUCUCACUCAGGCAAGCUGAAUUCUUGGGAGAUAAACAGAAGGUACUCUUUUAUCAUUGACCCACCUACCUUUAGUUGGUGACAACAUAAACAGCAGGACGGAGAUGAUGAUGGAGGUGCUCUUCCUAACAGAUUCAGACACAGAAUACCUUCAAGAUUUUAUUGUUCUUUUCUUUUCUUUUCUCUCUCUCUCAUUCUUUCUUUUGCCUGUUUUAUUGCUUGCUUUUAAAUUUAUUUUUAAAUUCAGCAAUACAAAAUAUCUAUUCUUCCUUCACCUUUUCACUUCAAGCCUGGAAUGUUGGCCUGGAGUAUGUGGAUUAGCUUCUAAAGAGAGUGAAUCUCCUGAAAUUUUACAUUCAACUGUGUGAGUACACGUAUGCAGAAGAAGGUGUAUGACUUUUGUCAGAUCCUAAAGGGUAUCCAACCCCCAAAACUGGGAGAACAACUUACUUAAAUCCAUAGAUAUACAGGGGCUCAAAGAAAAUAGAACCAGUGCUUAGAGAGGUAUGUCAUGGUCCCCCACUCAUUUCAUGAGCAGCAAAAAUUGGAUACUGAAGAGUGGAAGAUUUUUGUAUUUCAUUAUUUCUGAAGUACAUUCUUUAGUAAGAAAGCUAGGAAAUGUGUGACUUCCAGAGCUUCUGCUAAAUGUCACUUUAAUAGGAAGCACUUUCAUUGAAAAUAUUAUUUCAAUGGGAUUCUCUUACUCCUUCAACCAGCUAGUAUAUAUUAGGGAUUUGGGGAUUAUAAUGUUGCUCAGCCACAGGUCAAUUUUGUGCAAAUAUUUCAUUUCUUCCUUCAAAUGUCUGGUAAUGAAUGUAACCUUUUAUUUGUUUUCACUGCUUUCUUGCCUAUUCAAAAUUAUUCUCAGGCUGUAUUCCAGAGUGGAGAAACCAAGUAGAGAUAAAGCUUUUGAUGAUCAAUAAAGUAGACACAGAUGGUGUGUAGGAUAUAGCAGUGGUUUUCAGAAGCAAUUUUUACAGUUCUAAUUCUUUUACUGUUUCUAAUGUCAUGUUUACCUGAACUAAUUCUUCCUCUUAUUAUUCAUUCUCUAUAAAUACACUCUUAUUUGUAAGUGCUCAGAAAUAUGCUACCUAAAAAAGACUUCAAUGGCACUUCUGAUUCACCCAAAGGAAGUAAUUUGUUAUAAAUUGAAAGGUUGGGUUUAAAGAGAAAAUGGAUUGUAGAACAUUGUAAGGAGCUUUUUUUUUUAAGAAAGAAUUUGUUUCUCACAAGAAAAGUUGGCCUUGUGAAAAUUUGAGGAAAAUUGUAUUAAACAGAAAGCUAUUUUCUGAGGGAGCUGUAGUGUAAGGAGAGAUUUUUAAGGUUGUUUUCAACCUCAAAGUUUUGGCUGUUCAGAAGAUUCAGUGAAUAUAUCUUUCUGCUACCCAGGGAGAAAGCCAAAGAGAAAGUUGGCAAACUUAAAAUCUUGUUAUAUUAUCUUCAGGUCCUUAGCUGAUCAUUUCUGCAUAUUUAAGUAUAUAAUAUAUCUUAAUGUUUGUCUGUGUUUCCCAGCGGAGACCACUAUAUAAUAAAUAUAUGGUACUACUUUAUGUUUGUUUUAAUGUAUUGCCUUAAAAGUCAACUCUACCGUGGAAUACAUGUGGCCUCAUUCAUGUGACCAUUUAUUAUUGAACUUAGCAUGUCUUUGCGCUGUACAUCUUUACUAUUUCAAUGACUUCUAAAGUUCUGCAUAUUAAAAGUCACCUUUUUCAAUAGCAUAGCACUAAAAAUAGAAGCAGUCACAGAUGUAUCAUUAAUGAAUAAUCAAUAAAGAUAUCCUUCUAUAAAGCCUACUGAUUGAUUUUGAUGCCAGUUAUGCCUCUUUUUUUUUUUUUUUUUGGCUUAGUAUUAGUGGCUUGGAAGAAAGGUACUUAGGGCCCAUUGAGCAUUUUAUAUUCGUGGAAUUCAUUCCUGAUGGUUAGCAAAGUAUUAUUAACUUGUUUUGAGUCAUUGGAAGAAGUCAUAACAGAGAGAAAUGUAUUUAUCAUGGUUUAUAUUACACAAGAUAGUAACUCUGGGGAUAAAAAUUUAAGGUAUAUAUCUUAAAAAUUGUUUUGACUGCACAGACUACUUUAUGAAUAGGAAAAUAUAAAUGUCUCUAAUCAGAUAAUUUUUAAUUAUUUGGAAUAAUAAACAUUUCUAGCUUUGAACUUCUAUGCUUAUCUUGUAAUUUGAGUUGCAUUUGGUUUAUUUCAAAGAUAACAGAGGAAUACUCAAAUGAGAGGUUGGGGUGCUUGCCUGGCUGUGCAUCCCCCAAGAGGCUUCACAAGGUGUCAUUACUUUAGUGGGCCUAAAUCUGCUCCUCAAACUCAGAAGUUCUAAAUUUUAUUUUUGUCAGCUUACUCAUAGUAGACUGAUUUCUUGAUGUAAAUCAAACUGUUUAUUUUCCCUGAUAAGUAAUUGUGAGGUAGAUCAGAACUCUUGGUCUCUCAAAAACAUUAUAUUCUCCUAUAAAAGAUCUACGUAGAAAGCCAAUUAUAGUCAGACUACCAAACCAAUGUAUGUUCAGAAUAAAAGGAGUCCUAUGGCUCAAACACUUACUGGCAUCUGACAAAACAGUAUGAAGCAUCUAUCUAGAAUUCUCUCUGGAUAUAAAUCCCCUGCUAGACACAAGCUCCAUGUGGAUGAGGGCCAUUGUGGUUCUUGUACACCACUGUAUCCUUAGCACCUAGUCUGACAGCUAGAACAUACUGUGUUCAAAAAAUAUUGAAUAGAUGAAUGAGACUGUAAUUCUCUGAGUCUGUUGGCCAAGAUGCCUUCUCCCUUAACAGUGUUUGAGUGGGCAUUGCCAAGGUGUGCUUCUGGAAUUCUUUUUGCUAUUCUUUCAGUACUAUGCCAACUCCAUCCUGAUUGACUUUUAGUUUCAUUAGAUAGAUGAAUGUCUUCUGUUUGUCUUUGAUCCCACCUAAGAACCAGUCUAACCCUUUGAAGAAAUUUGCUGAACCCCUAAUGUGUUGUAUCAUAUUAUAUGCCAGUUUUGUAAUUUAUCUUAACUUUAAAAUGACUGGGAGUAAUCCUCACUUUUUUUCUUGUUCUUAACUUGUAUCCCAGUGGUUUGGAUAUUGGCACUAAACCAAUGUGCCUUCAAAUUCAGACAUUCCUAUUUUUAAUCACAAGAUCUUGAGUGAGUAAAAUAUCUAACACAUUGUAAAGACUUAAGUCAUAUGAUCAUUAUCAUAGAUAUAGCCUAAUACCAUUACAAGUGGCUGAUAUCCACAUGAUUACAAAACUCUGCAUCUAUAGUAUGCCCUCAUUUCUUACCCCUUUUCAGUGAGCAGAAGCCUAAGAACUAGUUGUACCCUGUGAGAAAAUAUUAGGAGCUAUGCCACAGAAAGGAAGAGUAAGAUGAAUCAUUUUUUCAGAUAUAAAAAGAUCAGAGAAAGAUGGGGCCGGGCGCGGUGGCUCACGCCUGUAAUCCCAGCACUUUGGGAGGCCGAGGCGGGCGGAUCACGAGGUCAGGAGAUCGAGACCAUCCCGGCUAAAACGGUGAAACCCCGUCUCUACUAAAAAUACAAAAAAUUAGCCGGGCGUAGUGGCGGGCGCCUGUAGUCCCAGCUACUUGGGAGGCUGAGGCAGGAGAAUGGUGUGAACCCGGGAGGCGGAGCUUGCACUGAGCCGAGAUCCCGCCACUGCACUCCAGCCUGGGCGACAGAGCGAGACUCCGUCUCAAAAAAAAAAAAAAAAAAAAAAAAAAAAAAAAAAAAAAAAAAAGAUCAGAGAAAGAUGGACAUACCAAUUUUGAAAUCUUUAAUUCAAACUUUGAUGGUACUAGGUCAAGAGUGUUUGAUGGCUCUAUCUCAUCUAUGUGAAUAGAAUUCCCAGCUAGAAUUUGAGUUCCAUAGAGUAAGAACCAAUGUGCAUUUUGUUUACUGCUAAUUCAUGCGGGUAUAGCAUAUGAUAGAUCAUUUUUUAAAAAGCUUUUUAAUGAAAGGGUGAAUACCUGAUGACAAAUUCUUAAAAUUGGGCUGUUUAUAUAAUAAUCUAUAAUCUAAAAUAAAGAUCCUUCUUAUUUUUCUACGAUUUACUUUGUAUUUAAUAUCUCAGUUAUCAUCACCCACUGUUACCAUAACCUCGCAGGGAAUGAACAUCCUUAAUGCAGAUUAUUCUCAAAUAAUCUAUAUUCAUACACACAAAAGUUUGAGUGGAUUGGGCCAAAUAAGAUAGUAUCUAGUUAUAACUUCACUCAAUUUUACCUUCUUAGGCAUUCCCUAACUAUCAUAUCUAAAAAUUGCCCCCUCCAUCACCAUUACUGGCAAUCUCCAUACCUGUUCUCUAUUUCUUCUUAGUGUGCAUCACAACCUGGUAUUAUAUUGUGUGUUUAUUUUUACUCUCAGUCACUAGACAAUAUGCUCUUUGUGUGCAGGGACUUGGUUUUGUUCUCAGCUGUAUCCCCAGAGCGUAAAAUAAUGACUGGUCCAUAUAUGCCUCUUGAUAAGUAAGUGUAAAAUAAAUAAACAGACUCAAAGAUAACAGAUGUCUAGACUUUAUUAGCGACUAACCAACUGAGCAUUAGUUUCACAGCAAGCCUGAUGUGAUUAGCUGUCAAGUUUCUUGUCUAUAGCGUUUGACCAAGUGUUACCAUUCACAUUUAAAAAGUCAAAAUGAAAACCUCACAAUAUCCUUCAUGUUGUGACUUCCAUAUUUGAUGUAUAUACUUCAGUUGGAUCUUAAAAUAAGAAUGUAGUUCACUUGUUUGUUGUUGUAUUUUACAGACGAUGACUUGUGCAUUUGCAUCCAUGAAAAUUCUUCAUUAAUAAAGAACUACACAAUUGCCUUGAAAGUUCUGAUAGUCACAGCAAACUCUAAGGAAUAGGAUCAUAUUACAUUUUGUAGUAUUUCUAUGGGCACUUAGAGUGUAGUAAAGUCUGCUAUCAAGUAUCAUACAUUUGCAUAUUCUGAGAAUCAAGUAAUGUAUGGCCAGGUAAUUGCUGCAACAUAAGACACAGUUUCAGCCCCAUCACAGAGCUAAUAGCGCAUGACUCUCUCUCUCUCUUCCAUACCACACAAAAUAUCGGUCAACUUAUAUAUCGAUAAACUCUAAAAUGUCUCUGCUAUUCCUUCCAUCUUUUUGUGUCUACUUCCAUUGCUUUUUCUCCUCUGUUUCUACUGGCUUAUCAAACUGUUAUUGCUGCCAGAUGUCAGAACAUUAAUUGAUUUGAGCCAAGGUAAGUCAAUGUCAGUCUGACAAGAAAAAGCUGCUGAUACAUAGGUACACUAGCAAAUGCUGAUACAAAGUGCACUGAUCAGGUGUCUCAAGGACUGUGCUCAAAGACAUUUAUUUAAGAUAAUGGAGUUAUUUUAAAGUUAACAUAAAUACUUCAAAAAAAAAAAACCCAUGCAUCUGAGAAUUUAGUAACCAUCUAAGAAAAUAGAAAAUGAAAACCAGAUUUUAAAAGGAUGCCUAAAAAGAUGUGAUUCUUAUCAACUAUUUUUGCUACAUAUUACAUAGAUCUUUAAAUUUUCAUUUGUUUCAUAAUUUGUAGCAAUAUUAUACAGCUGUAAAUUAGUUGAAAUUAAUAUUUAAGCUGAACUAGCAUAUUAUACCACAUCAAUUUUAAAAACUGCAUUCUAGAUUAUUACUUGGGAGAAGUAUUCUCUGUUAUAUUAAUGUUGAAACCAUUUAUUCCUUUAAAAAUGUGACUUCAACGAUGAUAAUGCCAACAGUAAUUUUGUCCCCACCUUGCCCUUCUAUCUUUUAUCUAACUUCAGUUAAAGGAAACUGAUAGAGAGUUGUUUACUAAUUUGGCUCAUGUUUUUUUCCAUACCUCUUAUUUUCAUUUGAAUUAUUACUUCAGCUAUAGAUGCUAUAGGAAAGAUUUAUGAAGUUAACCUCUUCCAGUUUAUUCAGCUCAAACAAGGUGGAGACAAAGAUACAUUUCAAGUUAGCACAUUUAGAUAUAAUGACUUGAUAAAUACUCAAAAGUCUUGAAGCUAUUCCAAACCUUUGAUAACAUUUAGUUUUACAAAUGUUUUACACACAUUUAAGUUACAAAUAAAUGGCAACAGAAAACAUAGUACUGUAAAUUAUCAGUGGUUCCUUUUGUUAUUUCUCUGAAAGAUUACAUAGGUUGUGAAUUCUAACUAUAAUAUUAACCCCCACUUAAAAUUAUUUUUGAACAAUAAGGGAGAAUACAUUAAUUUUUCAUCUUACAAAGGUAUGUCCCUAUCCAAAUUAUCUUUAUAAUUUAAUAUAAUAUUAACUUCAAUUUAACAUUUUUGGAGCAGCUAUAUUAAACAUUCAAUUUAACAUUUUUUUUGAGCAACUAUAUUAAAAGCCUGGGAUAUAAACAUAUAAAGACAAUGACAAAAUACUAGGUAAAGGGGGUUUGGAGUAUAACGACUAUCCAGUACAUUUUACAACUAAUAAAAGAGCUGGGUCAUGAGCUUCCAAGACUAGGGAGUGUCUAGUUUAACUUUGUUUGUUUGUUUGUUUGUUGUGGUUGUUGUUGUAUUGAGACCGAGUUUCCCUCUGACGCCCAGGCUGGAGCGCAGUGGCGCAAUCUCGGCUCACUGCAAGCUCCACCUCCCAGGUUCCCGCCGUUCUCCUGCCUCAGCCUCCCAAGUAGCUGGGACUACAGGCGCCUGCCACCACGCCCGGCUAAUUUUUUCUAUCUUUUAAUAGAGACAGGGUUUCACCGUGUUAGCCAGGAUGGUCUCUAUCUCCUGACCUUGUGAUCUGCCCGCCUAGGCCUCCCAAAGUGUUGGGAUUAUAGGCGUGAGCCACCGUGCCUGGCCUAGUUUAACUUUUCAUUUCUGUCAUUCAGCAUAGUGCCUGACCCACAGUUAAUACUUGGUAAACAGUUGCAUAGUGCGUGUUUUCAGUGCUGUGAUGGGGAUUUAUUUUUAAAAAGUACAAUGGAAGGUUUAGAAAGGAAACAACAUAUAAACCUGAUUUGUUCAAAAGUGAAGAUCAAAAUAGUUCUAUGGUCAUUUUUUAAAUUUUUUUAGUGCUCAGAAAUCCACACCUAAGCAUGAACCAUUUUUCGAUCUAUUAGUUCACCUUUGGAUUCACUUAUAGAUUAACUUAGUAACUUGGGCCCUAAAAACCAUAAGCGUUAACGCUUCAAAAAAGACGUAAAUUGUUAACCAGCUGCCUUAUUUUUCAGGAAACUUAAUUAGCUUUUCUUCAUAAAAGACAUUUUAUCUGCAGGGCUUAAAAAUGCAACGUUGUUUUAAUGUAAAAAAUAUAAUUGAGAAAAUAGCUUUGCAAUCCUCCUUCAUUCCAGUAAAUGUGUCCUGCUAGCCAUUUGUUAUUCCUAGUUCCUCUAUUUUUUUCUUUAACAUUUCAAAAAUCUUCACUGAAUAUUAAAAAUGAGAAAUUAUUGGGCACUUAGAGCGCUUCUCUCCAAUUGGCUCAAGGUCUUCUAAAGUCACUCCUUCAAUGAUUCAUGUGACAUCCUUCUGAAGUAAAAUGGUGCAACUGGCAAGUGCUGUUAUGCAUUGUUAUUAGAAGUUGAAACUCAAAAGUUAGGUGGUCUAGCCUUGGACCAGCUGGAAGUGUGUUGGCAUAUCUCAGGGUACAUGUCUCAGUGCUGGAAUUGCUGUACAAGACAUGCUACAUGCUAGGAAAGCAUUUCAGAGUAAUCUCCUGGCACCUCAAAGAGGCACACAGGAGCAGGCAACCUUUCUUCUCCUUCCUCCUCAACAGGAGCAAUAGAACUAAGGGCCAGAAUAGAGAACUCCACAAACUAAAUAAGGGCGCCCAUACUUUAAUGCAAAUUGUGAGACAGUUGGGUUCUGUAAACUCCCUCAUCAAUUUCCUGCACCUUCUCAUUUUUAAAAUGACUGUGCACUCGACUUGAAAGCUUCUGCUCCUUGCUUUCCUGCCAUCUACAACUAUGGUACCAUCAUAGGUGCUGGAAAUCCCUUGCACUUUCAUCUGACUCUCUCAUUUGAAACCCAUCUUUUAGUAAAGCUCCAUUACUUUUUCAGUCUUUAGUCUACACAGAAUAUAAGCAUUGCAAUUUAGUCUCUGUUUUGAACCUAUGCUAGUGGCCUAGAGAGGGAAAGAGAUGUCCCCAGGCAAUGUAAUGUCUAUAUCCUCUCUUCCUACAUGUUACUAUGCUGUGCCCCUGACUCAACCUUUUCAUUCUUCUAUACAUUUCCUUUAGUUAUCCUUUUAAUCAUUUCAUUGUGAUCUCUCAUCUCCUCAGCUACAGCACCCAAUUAAAGCCUUCUUCCCUGGCAGUACUCAUUGUCUCAGUGAUUGACUUUCUGUGCAGCAAGCAGCAGGACCUAGACCACACCCCUGCUAUUUUGGUAACAUUAUCACCCAGUUUUCCUUCUUUUUUCCUCUUUCUCCAGGCAAUCAAAUGUAGACACUCCUCAAUGUUAUUCCCGAGUGUGGCUUCGUCAUGUUCUGUUUUGCCUCCCCAGCAACCUUACCUCCUCCCAUGGCUUCAACUACCUUUCACAACAUCUAUCUCCCUAUACUUUGAAUUAAGCUUUUACCUGCUCAAGAAAUUUUAGAAACUCCCUGUCAUGUAUUUAAUAGAGUCAGUACUCCCUGGUUUUGACAUUCCUGAUCCAAAUCAAUUUCCCUCUGACCUAUAGUCAUCUCUUCUGUUACUCUCUAAUUUUCUUAUUGUUAGCCAAUCUAGGCCACUGGUUAUUUCCUCACUCUACACCCUCUUGCUCUUGUGCCUAACUUAGUCUCUUUCCUCUUCUUAAUUGCCCUUCAUACUAUCUCUACAUACCCUAAUUUUACCUAUUUUUCUAGAAAUACCUCAAAUACUGCAUCCUUCAUGAUGUUGUCAUUGCCUCUCCCCCUUGAAGCAGUCCCUUAUCAAUGUUUUGCAAUAUUUGGUCAGAAGCUUACUUGUUUCAGAAUCACUUAUGGUUCUUAUUAAAUAUGCAAAUUCCUAGGCCUCUGCCCACACUUACAAAUGUGUUAGGGCCCAGGCCUUCUUGAAUUUAGUAAGUGCUAAAUAAAUAUGGUUGAUUGAAAGAAAAUGGAUGAAUGUAUUUUAUUAGCCAGCAUCCAAUGAGCAAUAGAAUUUAUAAGGCCAUCUUAUAAACAUAUAUAUUGACCAAAGAAAAUAACAGUUUACAUUUUUCUUUUGUUUUGAAGAAAAAUCAAAGUAUAUUUAAACAAUAUUAGGAUAUUAUUUAAAAGAUUAAUCAUGCGUUUCUAAGUAUGGAUGCUUCCUUGAUCACUGCAAUGCUUAACAGACAACUUAAUAUCUUAAGGUGGCCUGGGAUUUACUAACCAUUUUCUCUUAGCAACUUUACUGAGUGCUCUUUGGCAAUAAUUUCCACAUUCUUACAUCUUCCUUUUCCUUUAAUAUGAAUCGCAUCAACUAGAUAAGCCAACUAUAAUUCUAUGAUUAUAUUAUUCUAUAAUUAAGCUAUAUGGCUUUAGGAGGGCUAUGACUUCUGAUUUUAGACUAUUCCUGGUCAAUCCUAUAAAACAUAAGUACCCACAUUUAAGUUCCCCCAGGGAUUCUCACAAAAGAGUUCAAGACUCUUAGACAAACUGUCUAAGAAACAAAUGUAUUUAAUUGUCCUUAAUAUCAUUCAUGUUAAAUUAUUUAACAGAGGUUGUUUUGAGUAUGUGUUAAAUUUAGCCCGUGUCUUACUGCUUACGUUAUUAACUGAUAUAUCACACUGAGACUGAUGUUUUGCCAUUGUGGUAUUGUGCCUGAAAAUGAAGCCAGAGUUCUGGGCUUUUUUGAUGAUGAGAUUUAAGAUCUAUAUUUCUUUGGCUAUAGUCUUGAGCAAAUAACUCUAAUAAGAAUGAAAAUAGUGUCUUUGGUAGAAAUUCAUUUUGUAACAUUUGAAUAUGGAAAGGUGACUAUGAAUAUACCCUCAAAAUUACUUGUGCGAUUAUUCCUGGGUUAUGUGUUAGGCCUAUGAAACCUAUUUUGAAACAUGUUCCCAUGCAGAAAUAUGACAAAUAAUGGGUUAAAAUUGUUGUGCUAUUUCCUCCUGAGAGUGUCAUGAUUAGAUAUAUCGCCUUCUCACAGUUCAAAUUUUAGUUUUACUGGUGGAUAUUAGUUUUGAAAGUAAAACUACAUUGCUUAUUCCCAUAUUAUUACUGCUAUUUAUUAUACAAUUUCCUAGAUUAAACAAUACAUUCAAAUGAGGUAAUGAAUUAUGUGUUUUAAGAGCAGAAUGAGCUAUAUUUGUUAUAGAAUAUUAUGUUAAAUCUUCAUUGACAACAUUAAAGAGUCAUACCUUUUAUGGGUGUUAGUUAAUUACGUAUACUUAUUUCCUUGGAACAAGAUAUAUUUUACAAAUAAAAAAGUUUUUCUAUAAUAUUUUGCUCUCACUAAAAGUAAUAAUAGAUUAUACAAUACAUUUUAUUAAAAUCUAAACAAUCAAGUUUGCUAGUUGUUUAUGUCAGUUCUUUGAUUUAAAUUUUCUGAGUCUAAAUGUUACUUCACUCUACCUUACAUUUUUCUCUUCUCUUGAAGAAAAUAAAAAUUAUUAUUUUUAUCUGUUUAUGUUUGGGUUUAUAAAUUAGACUUGGAAAUUCUAAUACUCAUUGGAUGCUAGCUAGGAAAGCUUGUCUGAACAAAUCUUACCCUUCAGCCUUGAUAUAAUCAGUUUCUUAGUAAAAAGCUACCAUCUUAGUUCUUUGAGAACCUUCUCAAUAAAUUCUUUGCAGAUUUCUCACAAUUUAAUAGGUUGGAAAAAAUUGGAAUGACUAGAAGACUGAAUUUAAUUUCAAGAUAAGCACAAAUUAGAAGAUUUCAAUAUGUUCCUUUCAAAAUUCUGCAUCUACCCGGGACCUGCCUCUGUGAUAAGGGGAUAUCUAUUCUCUGCUUUCUAAAGUAUCAGGUAACCCACAUAUGUCAUACAUAUGCCCUUGGUAACUUGAAGGUACAGGCAUAUUGAUUUUUUUAAAGGAACCUACAAAUAGUAGGAUUAUUUGAGAUUAAUUCUUAUGCUACCUUAGUCACUCUGUGAUAGCUAACUAUAUGCUGAGAGACUUCAUUAUUUUUCUGGGCAUAUACAUUCUGGGCAUAUACAUACAUAUACAGUGAUUUUAUACAUCACUGCUUAGGUGACCUAAAAGAUGUUAUACAAAAAUUCCAUUUAUUAGAGAGGACCCAGCCAUGAGGAAGAACUGGUACAGUGUGGGUGAGUAAAAAUGUAAACAGAAUACAUAGAUUUCCUAUUUUUUUCUUGGUUAUGUAAUAUUGGUUUAAGCACUGGUAUAAUUGCUUACUAGAGUUAAUGUUAGAUGUUAGCUUUUUAAACGUUAGGUCCAACUCUUUCUUCAGAGUUCUUCUAGAAAAAUGAUUAGGCCCCCUGUAUCUCCAUUUCAGAUUUCAAUCAAUUAUGUUGCGAUUCUCCUUACAUACUGUGUGGCAUUAAAUCACAGAAUUUCCCCAGAAGGAACAAUUUUAUGAUCCAUUCAUCACACUUGCUAUUUUUAUAUCCUUUGUGGAACCACAGGUUAGAUCCAAGGGUUGUCUAUUUGAUCUUUCUUACCUUUGAGAAAUAAAAGUUGAUUAUUUGGUUUUCUGAUGAAGGAAAAGAUGAUUUUUUCUCAACUUAUCCUUUGAGAAAUUAAUCUCCAUGGACUUUGAAUAAAAUGGCAUGUAGUGUCCCCAGGGUACAAAUGAUUUAGAAACAUCUUUUCCCACGACAGCUGUACAUUAGUAAGCUGCUUUGUAUAUGGUGGUGUCCUGUACCACAAAUGGACCAUUUCUCGUGGUCUUCAUUAUUAAAUGUAAGAGAUUAUUCUGACAUGUAAUGAAUAAUAUUUUAUAAAUUAUAAAUUAUAUAUCUAAAUAAAUUAUACAACUAAUGGUUAAGAUGACUGAUUUUAGACCCAUACUGUCCAGAUUUAAAUGUCAGCUUCACUUACUAGCUGUGUCUAGGAGCAAGUUAAUUAUUCUGUACCUCAGUUUCUUCAUCCAUAAGAUGAGAUCCCUAAUAGUUUGAAUCUCAUAGGUGUAUUAUAAGGAUUAAGUGAGUUAGUACACACUCAGUGUUGUAUGACUGGCACAUAGGAAGCAUUCAGUGUUAGCUAUUACUAUUUAUAGCUUAGGGGAAAAACAAAGUCAUACUUAUCAGAUGUCAGUACUGUGUUUCUCCAAAUGUUGCUUCUAAAUUUAUCCCUCUUAGGAAGGCAGGAUUUAUUUGUAAUUUUAUAUAUAGUUAAUUAGAUAUAUUUUGACAUAUUUACAAAAGAAUUUAUCUGCAUUUUAGGUAAUCUUAUCUAGCCACAGUACUAUGAUAUAUGAUUCUGGAAAAUGUGGAAAUGCAGCCAUUUGAUAUAUUUUUGUAGAUUAUGAGUUCAUAGUUAAUGAAAGAUAACCGAGUAGAUUUAACUAAAUAUUUAUAAUAACUAAAAUUAUAGAUGAUAAAUUAUAUAAAGUGAAAGAUUAGUGCACACAUUAAACUGGAGUUGCAUAUCACCUCUAUUUAAACUUUUUACUUAUUUCAAGAAAAUAAUCACAAACAACUACCCUCUAGAAAAGAUGGUUCAAAUUAAAUUCUGUCCACAGGAAAGGUAUGUUUGGAGAGUAAGUCCCCUGUAAUGAAACUAUUGAUAGUACUGCAGCCAGGCCCCUCAUAUGUCAAACACCUGCUUUGGUGAGACAAGUUUAAUGCAUAGAAAGAGCUCUUAAUAGCAGCAAUAGGAUUCCAAACCCUUGGCAUGACCUUUGUCGUUGAAAGUAAAAGAAAGAGGGUUGCAACUUGCUUAUUUUCUUCGUGCAAGAUCCUGCAUAAACCCCAAUACACGAUCAUAAUUCUAACUAAAUGAUUUUUUUAAACGUAGUGGUUUCUAUCACUCACUCCUUUUUCAGUAGACAUACUGAUGACAAUGUCACUUCUGUAAACUUUUGGAGAACAUAGUCUUACUAAACUUGCCAACACAAUGCUUAGGUUAUUUGAAGGUCACUUACAGUUGGAUUUUUUUUCUUUAUUUUUUUUCCUUCAACCUUAAGGGAAGCUAUUUGAUAAGCUUUAGUUUAUUAUACAAAAAAUGGGUAUUAUUUUAUUUGGACAUGCAGUAUUUGUAAGACUUCAAUUGUUUAUUUUAUUAGAAUGUAAAAUUGAUUGGAACAGCAUGUGUCAGAUCCUUGAGUUCAAACAAAUUCUUACCUUUUUCUUUAACAUCCUAUUAAUUGGUUCACAUAGAAGGUAUAGGGAAACUGGCUCUCCAGAAUGUUGGAAAGCUGGAGGCAGAGAAAUUCUUCAGGUAAAUCUAGAUAUUCAUCCUAUUUUCCCCACAGACAUAAGGAUGCAACAUUUCUAAUGCCAAGUCUGUUAUUCAAUACAUACACACAAACCCUCAUUGUAUUGUUAGUCUACACUUUUCCAAAUGGUGAUGUAAGUGAAAAGUAUAAAAGCACAGUGACAUAACAAAGGUUGGGUUUACCAGACCUGGUAAGACCCUACAGUGUCACUGGCAACCGUAUGUCCCCAGUGAAUCAUCUAGAGCAGUGGUCCCUAACCUUUUGGGCACCAGGGACUGGUUUCAUGGAAGACAAUUUUUCCACGGACAGGGGUUGGGGGUGCGGGGAUGGAUAGUUUCGGGAUGAUUCAAGCACACUACAUUUAUUGGGUACUUUAUUUCUAUUAUUAUUACACUGUAAUAUAUAAUGAAAUAAUUACACAAUGCACCAUAGAAUCAAGGGGAGCCCUGAGCUUGUUUUCCUGCAACUAGAUGGUCCCAUCUGGGGGUGAUGGGGGACAGUGACACAUCAUCAGGCAUUAGAUUCUCAUAAGGAGCGGACAACCUACACCCCUCACAUUCACUGUUCAAGAUAGGGUUCCUGCUUCUAUGAGAGUCUAAUGCUGCCACUGAUCUGACAGGCAGAGUUCAGGCGGUAAUCCAAGGAAUGGGGAGUAGCUAUAAAUACAGAUGACGCUUUGCUCACUCACCUGCCACUCACCUCUGCCGUGUGGCCCAGUUCUUAAUAGGAUGGUACCAGUCCAUGGCCCAGGGGUUGAGGACCCCUGGUCUAGAGGACAAAGUGCUGAGAUGGACGGUAUGUGCUCCUACUUGGUGUGACUACACUGGAAACAUAAUCUAGCUUUACAGUGAGCAUAUACAAUGGUAUUUAUUCCUGCCACUCUAUAGUUGAUCUGAAACAGCGUUAUAAGUUUUUUGUCACUUUAGAUACAGGCUUGAAUCCUACUUAGGCAUCAAGCCUAGUUGCCAUUGCUUUUCUACUUAAUAAGCAUGAAUUAGCUGGUGCUCUAAUAAGAAUUCAGCUAUGAUGAUAAAUGAGCAAGGCGUUCCACCCUUGUUAAAUAAAGAAAUAGUGAAAAAAAUGCAGAAUGACAAGAAGUAAAGUUUACAAAGGAUCCAUCAUUACAGAGUUAUCUUGGGUUUGCCCAUUGUAGAAAACGAAGUCAGUAAUUGAAAAUUUCAAGUUGAAACUGACUUUCACAGUAUUUGCUUAUAUUAGUACUUAUGCUAGUACUAAUACUUAUACUAGUACUGCUAUUGUCAGUACUAGUGAACCACUCUAAUGGCUCCACUACCUACAAGCUCUGUGCUUAGGAAAGUUAUUUAAUUUCUAUUAGGCUUAGGUUCCUGAUUUGUACAAUGAAAAUAAUAAUACUUCAAAGAAUAGUUGCAAGGAGUAAACUAAAUAAAUAAUAGCUGUAAGUUUGGAGCUUGACAUAUAGUUUGCAGUAAAUAAAAAUUUGCCAUUAUUAUUUAUGUUUAAAGUAGAUACUACUAUCUGUAUUUUACAGGAAAGGAGAAUAUUGGGGCUCCGAUAUUUUCACCCUCUAGCCUAAGUUCAUUCACAGCUAGUACGUUGAAAGCACACACGAUUCACAUCCAUGUGACUUCAAAGAGAGUGGAAAUUUGUAGCAGAUUUUCACCAUAGUAAGGUCCUGAAGCUGGCCCACUAAUGUUACAUUGCCCAAGUGUACACAGUUCAUUGAUAUAUGGCAUUUUUCUUCUCCCAGAUGUUGCAUCCUGCUUAAUUAUAUACCUUUCCUGUUUCUGAUUUUAAAAAUUGUAACGUUUUACCUUUUCACUCUGUGUGUGUGUGUGUGCUGUGUUGUGUGGUAUAACUUCCAUGUUACUGUUAAGAUGGAGAAAAAAAGACAAGGAGGGCGGCUCGACGGUAACACAGGUUUAUUGGACAAAGACCUGCGGAGGGGGAGCACCAGCGAGCGCAGGAGCCUCCUUUCCCGCUUGCAGGCUGGGGCAGUUGUAGGUCCAGGCGGGAGAGGUCUGAGGUUGCUGUGAAAUGGGGUGGGAAUGGUAUGCUGGGCUGCUGAUAAGGAAGGAAUUCACUGGGUUAGGGGUUAGGCCUGGGACCUGUCCCACAAGAUGUUUCUUCACGGUUCAGUCUCUGGUGGAAUUUUCCACUCUGACCGGAGUUUAUAAAAGGUGGGAGUCUGCAAAAUGCUGUGGCUUGGGCUAACAGUUACCUGAGGUCCUCUUACCUUUUAAGCUGUAAAUAAGAUUGGAUUCCGUGCCCCAUGAAAAGCCCAAUAUAGUUCUUCAGUUUUCUCUGAACUUCCAGUGGGUCUUACAUCCUCAUAAACACCUCUGUCUUGAACCACUUUUCUCUACAACUUUUUUGUUUUUUACUCUGUGUCCCUGCUCUGGUAUAUAGCCAAAUGGGGAAAUUGAUCUUUCUUAAGCACACAUGAUAAACACAUUUCCAUAAAAAUCAGCGUGCUCAGCAAUGUGAAUGUACCACACUUUUCUGAAUUAUGAGAAAGAUUUUGUAAAAACAGCAACAACAUAAAAUUGAAUAUUAGAUGUCUAAAAUUUUUAAUGUUUUCCCUCUAAAGGCCACUCUGCCUUUCCUUUCUUCUUUUUUGUAUUCCCCACCACCCACUAAUUGCCAUUAAUUUCUAACUUAGGAACAGUUUUGCUAUUUUUCAUUGCUUUCUCUCCUACUAACACAUGUUCUCAUCUUCUGCUUUCUACCAUAAGUGCCUUAUCAAGAUAUUUUCCUGAUUCUAGGCAAUUUUCUCUUUAAAAGAAAUACUGUUUUCAAGGAUUGAUACAUGCAUACACUAUAAUAGUAAGCCAUCUCAACUUUUCCUGGAAGAAAGGGUAAAAUUAAAUAAAAUUAAAAUAAAACAUAGCAAAAGUCACAAUUGAAAGGUGGCUCUGUGGGAAAAGAACUGCAGACCAGAGCUUAGAAAUUCCUUGAAAACUUCAGUAAAUCUUUAUGCGUUCUACUACACACUACUUGCAGUGGGGUACCACAUUUAGAAACACAGGAACAAUUUCUCUGUUCCCAGAAGCAAGCACUAGCUACAUACACAAAGCCCCUAGUCUCAGCUUAUCUGACUUACCACGUGAAGGGCAAUUUGGUUUUAGGUAUGAGUGUUGAAUCUCCAUUUUCUAACUGGAAUGAAAUUAUGAUUCCAAGAUGUUCUUUUCCUAAAAGCUCUGUGACUGGAUUGAAAAUUCCGAGUGUUAUGGCUUCAGUAGGUGUCUCUUCUGUGUAGGACUUAUAUUUUGUAUUUAUUUUCCAAAUUUUGGCUGUACUUAUUGGCACUUUUAUAUCCCAGGAAAAAUGCCAGUUAUUUGAGAAUUUUUAAACUAUCUUAUUAUCUAAAACAAUAUGUUCUUAUUAUCUAAAGAUUAACCAUGAAAUGAAUGAAGUCAUUGUUAUAAUGCUACUAUUAUUUUACUGUCAUCUGUCUUUGGUAUCUUCACCCUUCUAUGCUUUUUAGUUAAUCAUUUACUAUAUUUGUGUCAUUAGGCUAAUCAUUCUGCUCAUUGCUUUCUUACAGCUUUCACUGGAAGUUAAAGUUUAUUUAAAUUGGGCUUUCAUUGAGUUAUUACUUAAAUCUAUAUCAUGUAGAUUGAGAUUAAAGAUUUAUGCAAAGAGGCAUUUCCUAUUGCUUUUUGGUGACAAAGUCCUUAAUUUUUAACAGGUAAGAUAUACAAUGAUAAAACCAAGGAAACUUUAAAAAUAUACCUCCUUGCAGGUAGAGUUUACUAAAAUAUUCUAGACAGUAAGAAGCAAAUAUUCUUCUUAAACUUCCAGGACAAUGAUUCUGAAACCGGUUCAGGAGUCCAUUCCAAUUCACUCUAUUUUCUACUUUAUGUUACUGAGUAUAUUUCUUGCUGUUAUUUCAUCCUUACUGGAACCGAAGAAAAAUAGAUCCUUCCCUCCCACAUUCUCCCAAUCUCUAAAGAAUAAAGCUAAUUUGCCUUAGUCCUGAUUCCUCCAAGCAAAUCAAUUCCCAUUUGAUUAAACUCUCUUAGUAAAUAUCAGCCUUAGUGCCAAUGCUAAACACAGGACUCUCUCCUUAACAAAGGCUACAGAGAAAAACAUAUAUAAGAGGUCUCAUCAUGAACUAUUAUUAGGGAAUGUUUAUAAGGCCUAAAUUGAAAACUCUAGCGCUUUAGUCAUGGAGGAACAGUAUGAUUCCUUAGAAAUAAAAAAGCUGACAUUCAAAGCAAUUUAAUCAAAGCUCUUGCCAUUCCCUCUUGGGUUUCAGACACAAUAUGAGGCUGUUUUAAAUCAUUGUGACUUCCAUCGCUCAGCAUCUUUGGAAAAUUCAAAGCUGUGUUUGGCACCUGAAAGCCUUUGCAUUUCCCUCCUACCAUGAUGGAAGUAAAUUCCUCAUAUGCUUCUUAUUUUAGAUAUUCAUCUGAUUUUAUCUGGUUUGGGCUAUUUGCUGACAGUGCAUGGUUCUUGAAUAAUACAGAUAACGUACAACAAACACACUCUGCUCCCUGGUACACAGGAAAUGAAGAUGCUCACAGUACCCGCCUCCAUGAACUAGCUCAAUAAAUUUGAAUUGCUCAUUAGAUUUCCAAUGCCUCGUUGUUGCCUAUAUGUGAAGAGCUUAAGUGAAUAGGAAUCAGAUGGAAGGUGGGGGAGAACACACAGAGAUUUCACAUAAUUCCUGUUGCCAGAGAAACCAUUUUCUUGCUGUCUGGGCAUGCACCGAGUAGCUUAGAUGAACUGGAGGCUCAGCACAGCCCUUGCUGUGACUUUAGUAAAGAAAACAAACAGAAGGGAGAAAAUGCUUACAAAGUAAAGCAGAAUUGGAUAUUAAAAUGUUAUUUUAAUUAGAAUGGUUUUGUAGACUGAGCUUUGAAACCUUGCCCCCUAAGGACACUGAUCCAUCUGACUACACAUGUGUUUCCACACUUUGUGUUCAUUUAUGUAUCUUUUUUCUUCUGUGUCUAGAAGACCAUGUCUUCAUAUAUGUUUAUGUACACUAUUCAUAUUUACACAAGUAUAUUCUCUUCCCCCCUCUUUCUUUCACCUCUUCCCCCCACAACACAUAUCACACAACUGUGCUCUUUUGAAAACAUGGGAAACUAUUCUCAGUGGAAAAAAAAAAGAAUGUGGCAGUAACAGAGUUUGCUUACCCAAGCCGAAAAGAAAUAACAGAAAACGAGGAAGCACAAGGAGAGUACAAACUGUGAAUUCUAGACUUGUUUAUUUAACACUUGGAUCUUUUUGAUGAAGGAUGGUUGCUAAAAACAAAAGUUAGAAAAUCAAUUGAGAAUACGUGAGGUAAAACGUUCUGUAUGCAUGGUUCUCCAUGCAUUUUUCCAUGCAUUGUGAGUAUACAAACUAUAUACUGAAUCAACAUAGUACCUCCUUUUGUGAUACUAUUGAAGGAAAGCAAGUAAGAGUAGAUUUUGUAUUUAUUUGUGUAUGACAGCUCUGAAAAGAGCUAUUACAUAUUUUGAAGGUUCUUGUUUUUUAAUGUACCGCCAUUCAAGGUUUCAUGGGGAUUUUGACUUCUUGACCUUUCAGAAGAGGGAUAGUUGGCAAAUACCUUUGAUGUAUAGAGAUUCUGUAAGACUGAGUCUGUCAAUGAAUUCCUUGAUAUAUCUCAUCCCAUGUAGAAAUGGUCACUUUCUGUUAGUGCCAUCUCCACUUGUAUGUAGUUUUAGUCAAAGUGCCAUCUUACGCCACAUGUUUGUCUUUCUGCCUUCAUCCCCACUGACUUUAUCAAAUAUGCCAAAACUAUAACCAGGGCCUAUUCAAUUUUAUAGCUCCUAUGCCAAGCAUAGGGCCUAGUACAUAAGUACACAAGAAAUGCUUAUUAAAAUGAAUGAAUUAUUUAAUUAGCACUUUACCCCAAAGGAAUAAACAUUAUGCACAAGGUAACAUUACAAAUUAGGAGUAAAAUAGGAGACUAAAUUCAAGGUUCCAAAUUGUCAUGUCAUAGUCAUCACUGAACACAUUUCACGUUUAUAAAAUAAGAAAAUCACAGGCUUUCAAACAUAGUCUCACAUUUCCAAAAGCAUAUUUUUUGGGGAAAAAAUAUUAAGUAAUUUUGGUUUUCAUUUCAAUUCUUCUGAUUAAAGGUCUAAUGUUUUCAUUUUCGUAUGUAAAUUCCCAUCUUAGAUUGUUGCGAUGCUAAAAUCUUUGCCUGUACAAUUACUACAGAUGGCUGAUAGUUUCAAAACAUUCACACUAAAAUUAUUUAGUUUUUUUGUAAUGUAUUGAUUUUUGCUUUCCAUUUGUCUUGGGGAUGGAAGAUUUAAAUUCUUCGAUUUUUGAUGUUUUCUUCUGCUUUUCUCUCAAUUCUUUAAAUCUUUUUGCCUUUUGUACAUCAAUUAAACAGAUAACAGUAGAAGUUAUUAAAGAUCCUCACAUAAUAAUGUCAUUACCUAUCAUUUCUGAGAGUAGAUCUUGUCAUUCGAUAUGAUUGCUGGAUUCUGACUUUACCAACUAAAAUGCACCUACUGCCCUUUACUCUUUUGUAUAUUUUGAUGAAACUCUACUUCUUUUUAAGAUCUCAAUUCAAGUUUCAAUGAAGUGCAGUGAGUUUUGUCAUGCUCCCUUUCCCCGGUUAGUUUAGCUGAUAAAAAAGCAAAGAUACUGCAGCGUUAGCUUGCACUGGGAAUCAACGCCUUCUUGUGUUAGAUUUUUUCAUUAUAAAUGCAAUUGACAGAGGUGUCUUUUAUAAGCUAUUUGUUAUACAAUCUUUAUAAAUAGCUCUCAUCAUGUAUAAGACAAGUCUAAAUUUGUUUGGAAAUAGCUUCUGAAGACACCCUGCUGUGGCUUCCUCAGAGUGCCAGGCAGGCAUUCAGUGGGGGAGUCAGACAGAACAAACUUUAUCUAGUCAUCUUUCCAUCAGCUUGAAAUGAUGUGCAUCACAUCCAGCUUAAAUGAUUUACUGUAAGUAGGAACUUGGUUCAUAGACGAGUGUAUAUAAUCAAGCAAUAUGUAGCCAAACUCUACAUCAUCUAAGAUACAUUUUAUUUUAAUUUCUUUUUAGAAAUGUCUUGCUUAGCUAUUUUUGUUGACAUUGCCAGUAGCACUGUUCCUUUUAACCUAGAGUUGACCUGCAGUCCAGUGGAGGAAGGUCUUAAAACUCAAACAUGCAAUUUCUAAAGACCAAUGUGUAUAAGAAAGAUAGAAAGCUUAGGACUCUUUAAGUUGUUGGUGCCAUAUUUCUAUUCAAAUGCAAGUUCAAAAAUACAUUUCAAAGUCAAAUAGAAAUAGUUUUUGGAUUAUCCACCAUUUUGGAUUAUACACACCACUGCUCUCCAUUACUGCAGGUAAUUAAGAGCUGCCUUAUUCUGUGAAAAAUAUUUUCUUAAACAUCAACGCUCUCUUCUAUCAAACUUUCACAAGAACUUCAGUAAGUGAAGCUGACUGAUUGUAAUUCCACCUCCUUUCUCUACUCAGUCUCUGGAGAAGAUAUGCCAGAGCAACAGUAUCCUACAAAGCUCUUAGGAAGGAGGUAAGAAGAGAAGCUGGGGACCUAAAGACUCCAUCGUCAGUCCUUGAUCAUGGAAAUUUUUGAACAUAACAUUUCCAAUGGUCAUAAUCAGAAAAUAUGGCUCUAAGGGGAAAAAAGAACAAAAUGGAAAUAAUCUGACAAGUAUAUAGACAGGACAAAAUUAGAGAGCAAAAGCAGACUAUAAAGAUGAUCUAAUUCACCCAUUUUAUUCCUGCCCCCAUUUUACACAUAAGCGUUAUGAAAUCACCCUUUCUAGGUAAUAACAUCCCUCCUCUCUGCAACCUCCAUUCCUUGCUCAUAUUUCUAAUGUUACCUUAUUAUUACUAUUAUAUAUACUCUUCUGAAACUAUUUGCUUGUCUUUGACACCUCUUUAGUCUGAGACCUAGUAGGGGGCUCAUGCUGAUGCCAGCACAGUCCAGACCUCAAAUAGACAAUGAAUGUUUCCUUUGUUGAGUCUAAUUAAUUAUAUACGUAAACUUCAAUGAUGUGCAAGUUUAACACACAUAUAUCCUGUGAACUUCAUAUCACUAAAUGUGAGUAUGAACCUCAGUCCUUUGAAUAUUGCAAAGUCCUUACAAGUGAUGUUGUGAUCAUCAUGCACUAGACUACAAAGAGAAUUUAUAAAGACUUAGCUGAUUUCAAUUGCCAGAUUAAUUAUAUACUCAGAGCUUACCUGUCAAACAGUCAAACAUUCAUUGACUCCAUUUUAAAGUUGUUUAAGUAUUUUCUAGAUGGUAAGAGCAUUACUUUUUGAUUUAGUUGCCAGGCUUAAACUCAAAUUCCUUUGGUAAUAAUCAUCAAUUUUGCAAAGCAUAAAUGAAACUGUGAAAUUAUAGGUACAGAGGGGUUGCCUGUAGAUUGACAAACCAUAUGACUCUAGAGUUUUUGUAUCUUUUGACUUUCAAGAACUGCAUAUGUUUUUGUGUCAAGCGGCAUUUAAUCAUUCCAUCAGUAGCAAUAUACUGAGCUUUAUGAGCAUUUCUCUCUGUUAAGCUCUCAACUCAUGCCUUCCUUUGAUCACUACGGUUCAUCAAUAGGAUAUUGUACCCACCCUUGCAAUAGCCCCCUGAGGAAUGUGUUUGGUAUUAUCGUGCCAUGGACAGAUAAAACUCCAGAUUCAUUCAGAGAUUAAGCUUGCUUCCUCCUUGUUAUGUUGUAGUUCACUUCUCUAAGAAUGGGUCAAGAGUCACAUUCUUUGAUGGGGUUAAUAUGGAGUGAUUUGGUAUCCAUUACCUACACCCUCUCCCCAAACAUAGGGUUCUUUGCACCACCUAUGCUAAGACCUGGGAAUCCCCAGGGUACUUGGACUCAAUCAGGAUCAUGCAGGGCUGGCAAAGGAUUUAAAAUUAGCAUUAGUCCUGAUUUUGAUGGUUAUCUAGCUGUGUGAAUUUGGACUAGGUACUAACUUAUCUGAAUUUCAGCUUCCUGUUUAGUAGAAUGUGUGUAAUCUUGUCUGCUAUAAGGAUUAAAUAAUGUAAUAUGUACUUAGUAUGUGGUAAUAUGUACUUAUUAACAGAAAUAACCAUUCUGUUAGCAAUGCUUAUUUAACAUGAGGCAACUCUCGUGAAAGGUCCCUUCCCUGUUGAGGGCUGCAUUUACCCUCCUGGAUAUGUUAGUAACUUAGAAAGUUCUGUUUGAAGGUUUGAUGACUUCUAGGUUUGUGAUCUAAAAGAAGAGUCAUGAAAAGACUGUGCUGACCUGGCUGGCUGUAGGAUUGACACAAGAGAAACAUGCUGUACAGGGUAAAUACUGGGAAGUUAUGAGGGAGCAGAGUAUUUAAUCUGUGAUCCUACAAACAUAGACCAGGCAAAAAGUCAAUACCAAAAGAUCAUGUGUAAAUGCCAGGAGCCAAGCAUAGAAGAUACUAAGAGAUAUAGCUGAGGACAGCAGCUGAAGAUGAGAAAUGAGGAAUUAGCUAAGGCACAAACACAUAUAAAUUCUGCCGGAUGGCAAGCCAUCUUCAGGGCCUAUUUCAACUAAGCUCCUAAGAAACUCAUUGAGGACUGGGAUAGUAAAUGUAAUUUGUACUGUGUGUUCUAGCUUAUAUGGUGCUCAGUAUAGUCACAAAAUAAACGUGAACUGAAGUGAUGGCCACAGACAUGGGAAAAGUAUGAUGAAUGCUCUAACGGUGAAACACAGGCCAGACAACUGACCUAGGCCAGAGAUGUCUAAGAAAGCUUCCUACCAAAGAUGAAAUCACAGGCACCACAAGGCCACAUAAGGAGGGUGAGGUCCCUGGAGUGGAUUAUAUUUUCAUCACUGUUGAAGAUUUUAUGGAAUUGGAGAAAAGUGGUGCUCUCCUAGAAAGUGGGACUUAUGAAGACAAUUACUACGGUACCCCAAAGCCGCCAGCAGAACCAGCACCAUUAUUGUUAAAUGUAACAGACCAGAUACUUCCAGGAGCCACUCCAAGUGCUGAAGGAAAACGGAAGAGGAAUAAAUCAGUGAGCAACAUGGAGAAAGCCAGUAUAGAGCCUCCUGAGGAGGAAGAGGAAGAGAGGCCUGUGGUCAAUGGAAAUGGAGUAGUAGUAACACCAGAAUCCAGUGAACAUGAAGACAAAAGUGCAGGUGCCUCAGGGGAGAUGCCCUCCCAGCCUUAUCCUGCACCAGUGUACAGUCAGCCUGAGGAGCUGAAGGAGCAGAUGGAUGACACAAAGCCAACUAAACCUGAAGACAAUGAGGAACCAGACCCAUUGCCUGAUAACUGGGAAAUGGCCUAUACAGAGAAGGGCGAAGUCUACUUCAUUGACCAUAACACAAAGACAACAUCAUGGCUGGAUCCACGACUUGCGAAAAAGGCUAAACCUCCAGAAGAGUGCAAAGAAAAUGAGCUUCCAUAUGGCUGGGAAAAAAUCGAUGAUCCCAUUUAUGGCACUUAUUAUGUUGACCACAUAAAUAGAAGAACACAGUUUGAAAAUCCUGUCCUGGAAGCAAAAAGGAAGCUACAGCAACAUAACAUGCCCCACACAGAACUUGGAACAAAGCCCCUGCAGGCCCCAGGUUUCCGAGUAGACAGCUCCUCAUGGACAUUACCUAGGCCCAAAUCCAUCCGCCCCCGUGCUGCCCCGGAGAGGUCGCGCAGCGUGAAUGACUUGUCUUACUAUCAGCGCGACCCAGCAGGGAGGCCCUGGCUGUUCGAAAAACCACUCUUCACCCGGGAUGCAUCCCAGUUGAAGGGAACAUUCCUCAGCACCACCCUAAAAAAGAGCAACAUGGGCUUUGGAUUUACCAUCAUUGGUGGAGACGAGCCUGAUGAGUUUCUGCAGGUGAAAAGUGUGAUUCCGGAUGGGCCUGCAGCACAGGAUGGAAAAAUGGAAACAGGUGAUGUCAUUGUCUAUAUUAAUGAAGUUUGUGUCCUUGGACACACUCAUGCAGAUGUUGUCAAACUUUUCCAGUCUGUUCCUAUUGGUCAGAGUGUCAACCUGGUGUUGUGUCGUGGCUACCCUUUGCCCUUUGAUCCUGAAGACCCUGCUAACAGCAUGGUGCCACCCCUUGCAAUAAUGGAGAGGCCACCUCCAGUGAUGGUCAAUGGAAGACACAACUAUGAAACAUAUUUGGAGUACAUUUCUCGGACCUCACAGUCAGUUCCAGAUAUAACAGAUCGGCCGCCUCAUUCUCUGCACUCCAUGCCAACUGAUGGUCAGCUAGACGGCACGUAUCCACCGCCCGUCCAUGAUGACAAUGUGUCUAUGGCUUCAUCUGGGGCCACCCAAGCUGAACUUAUGACCUUAACCAUUGUGAAAGGUGCCCAGGGCUUCGGCUUCACUAUUGCCGACAGUCCUACAGGACAGCGGGUGAAACAAAUACUUGACAUUCAGGGAUGCCCUGGCCUGUGUGAAGGCGACCUCAUUGUUGAGAUCAACCAGCAGAAUGUACAGAACCUGAGCCAUACAGAAGUAGUGGAUAUACUUAAGGACUGUCCCAUUGGAAGUGAAACUUCUUUGAUUAUCCAUCGAGGAGGUUUCUUUUCUCCAUGGAAAACUCCAAAGCCUAUAAUGGACCGAUGGGAGAAUCAAGGCAGUCCUCAAACGAGUUUAUCUGCUCCGGCCAUACCGCAGAACCUGCCCUUCCCACCUGCCCUUCACAGGAGCUCCUUUCCUGACUCAACAGAGGCCUUUGACCCACGGAAGCCUGAUCCAUAUGAGCUCUACGAGAAAUCUAGGGCCAUUUAUGAAAGUAGGCAACAAGUGCCACCCAGGACCAGUUUUCGAAUGGAUUCCUCUGGUCCAGAUUAUAAGGAAUUGGAUGUUCAUCUUCGGAGGAUGGAGUCUGGAUUUGGCUUCAGAAUCCUCGGGGGAGAUGAGCCUGGACAGCCUAUUUUGAUUGGAGCUGUCAUUGCCAUGGGCUCAGCCGACAGAGAUGGCCGCCUUCACCCAGGAGAUGAGCUUGUGUAUGUUGAUGGGAUUCCAGUAGCCGGCAAAACCCACCGCUAUGUCAUCGACCUCAUGCACCACGCAGCCCGCAAUGGGCAGGUCAACCUCACUGUGAGAAGAAAGGUGCUAUGUGGAGGGGAGCCCUGCCCAGAGAACGGGAGAAGUCCAGGCUCUGUAUCCACCCACCACAGCUCUCCACGCAGUGACUACGCAACCUACACCAACAGCAACCACGCUGCCCCCAGUAGCAAUGCCUCUCCCCCUGAAGGCUUCGCCUCCCACAGCCUGCAGACCAGUGAUGUGGUCAUUCACCGCAAAGAGAAUGAGGGCUUCGGCUUUGUCAUCAUCAGCUCCCUGAACAGGCCUGAGUCUGGAUCCACUAUAACUGUGCCCCAUAAAAUCGGACGCAUCAUUGAUGGGAGUCCUGCAGAUCGCUGUGCAAAACUAAAAGUGGGAGACCGGAUCCUAGCAGUGAAUGGCCAGUCUAUCAUCAACAUGCCUCACGCUGACAUCGUGAAGCUCAUCAAGGAUGCAGGUCUUAGUGUCACCCUUCGCAUCAUUCCUCAGGAGGAGCUCAACAGCCCCACCUCGGCACCCAGCUCAGAGAAGCAGAGUCCCAUGGCGCAGCAGAGUCCCCUGGCACAGCAGAGUCCCCUGGCCCAGCCAAGCCCAGCCACCCCCAACAGCCCCAUCGCCCAGCCAGCACCACCUCAACCACUUCAGCUGCAAGGACACGAAAAUAGUUACAGGUCGGAAGUGAAAGCAAGGCAAGAUGUGAAACCAGACAUCCGACAGCCUCCAUUCACAGACUACAGGCAGCCCCCGCUGGAUUACAGGCAACCCCCAGGAGGGGACUACCAGCAGCCCCCACCCUUGGACUACAGGCAGCCUCCCCUACUGGACUACAGGCAGCACUCCCCCGACACCAGGCAGUACCCUCUGUCGGACUACAGACAACCCCAGGAUUUUGAUUAUUUCACUGUGGACAUGGAGAAAGGAGCCAAAGGAUUUGGAUUCAGCAUUCGUGGAGGAAGGGAAUACAAAAUGGAUUUGUAUGUGUUGAGACUGGCAGAAGAUGGACCAGCAAUAAGGAAUGGGAGGAUGAGGGUAGGAGAUCAAAUCAUUGAAAUCAAUGGGGAAAGCACAAGGGACAUGACACAUGCCAGAGCAAUAGAACUCAUCAAAUCUGGAGGAAGACGAGUGAGGCUGCUGCUCAAGAGAGGCACGGGACAGGUCCCAGAAUAUGGAAUGGUACCUUCCAGUCUCUCCAUGUGCAUGAAAAGUGACAAGCAUGGGUCCCCAUAUUUCUACUUAUUGGGCCACCCUAAAGACACGGAAAGAUCCAAACUGGCUAGAACUGACAAUAGGAAGGACGAACCCGCCCCCUGGAGUUCUCCCGCUGCCGCCGCCCCAGGUCUGCCGGAAGUAGGCGUCUCCCUGGACGACGGCCUCGCUCCAUUCUCUCCAUCACAUCCAGCCCCACCCUCCGACCCUUCCCACCAGAUAAGCCCAGGCCCAACUUGGGAUAUCAAACGGGAACACGACGUUAGGAAACCAAAGGAGCUUUCAGCCUGCGGCCAGAAGAAGCAGCGCCUCGGGGAGCAGAGGGAGCGCUCGGCGAGUCCGCAGAGGGCCGCGCGGCCGAGGCUCGAGGAGGCGCCCGGCGGCCAGGGGCGGCCCGAGGCCGGCAGGCCCGCCUCGGAGGCCAGGGCGCCCGGGCUCGCGGCGGCAGACGCGGCGGACGCGGCGCGGGCGGGCGGGAAGGAGGCGCCCCGUGCGGCGGCGGGCUCCGAGCUCUGCCGGCGCGAAGGCCCGGGGGCUGCGCCGGCGUUUGCCGGCCCGGGCGGCGGCGGCAGCGGCGCGCUGGAGGCCGAGGGCAGGGCGGGUGCGCGCGCGGGUCCCCGGCCGGGCCCGCGACCCCCGGGGGGCGCCCCGGCGCGCAAGGCCGCCGUCGCGCCGGGGCCCUGGAAGGUGCCGGGUUCUGACAAGCUGCCCAGCGUCCUCAAACCCGGCGCCUCGGCCGCCAGCAGAUGAGCCGCGCGGCCACGGCCAACCCGCCCGCCCCGGCGCAGGCAGUUCUUCUUAGGUUCCGUCUCACGGCGUUUUAAUUUAUUUUCACUGUCACACGCAUAGAUCCACGAGGCACCAAGGCCUGGGAGCAUCGACGUGAAGUCCCACGUGUCCGGUGUGCUUGGGCGGCAUCGCAUCAACGCGCAGACCUAAACUGAUCCUAAAGCCCCCGGUUCCCUUGUGGGGGCUUUGGCAGCUAUGGAAGAACCAAAAUAACGUGAAGAACAUCACAGAGAGACAGUGCAGUGUAGCUUUAGUUUAAGAAAAAAAAAUAUUCCUCCCCACUGCAUGAAGGACUUGGAUGUCAUCCAAACUUUAUAUCAAGAAACAGGACAAAGUUAAGAGCAAUCACAAACUGGAAUAUCGCCUUAAAAAUCAAACUGCACGGAGCAAGCUGAAACUGAGACAAGAUUAUAUCUUUUAAUUGAUCUAAAGCGUUGUAAAUAAAUUGUUCUCGACAUAUCUAGACAGGGGUUAAAGGGUUUCUUUGACACAUUCGGAACCGUUCACCCAUGACAUGUUUCCAUGGCUCACCCUUGGCAUCCAUCCUCGGUGUUAGCAGCAGCGUUCCCUGCCUCCUGCAGGAUGACUUAGAAAUCUAGUGAGUUUCUUGGUGUGAUGCCAUUUUUAUUGCCCUUUCUGUGAUCAAAUCAUAUUUCUGUACAUUUUCAGUGGUAGAAAAAAAAGGUUUUAAAAAUUGUAUCCUAGGGAACAGUUUGCCAUAAGUCAGAAUUUUGCAGUUUAGCUCAUAGAUCUUAAUUGGUUUUUCUCUAAAAUAUGAAUUUUAUAAUUGAAGGACCACAAUUUGUUUAAUCAAGAUAGGCAACGCUGCAGUUCCUUUAUGAAGAGGCUUUUCUGUCGUCCCAGGCUAGCAGAGAUGGAUAGCUUCUUUGUCAGCAAUGUGAUUUCACUUAUUUUAUUGUCUUAUUUUAAACCCUGUCUCCAUGACUUCAUUUGCACUUUGACAGAGCAGAGGCAGAGUAUUUGUCUUAUAUUUCUCAGAUUAUAAUAUUAAAAAAUUACAAUCAAUUUAUUUUCAUUAAAGAACGUGAGUCUUUUUAGCAUUCCUUUCUGCUUAUCCUUCUUUCCUUACCCUUUGUCCUUUUGUUUCCAUUAGUUUUCUUUCGUCUUGUAUUCCUUGCCACUUUAUUUUGUUAGCAACUUCUAGAUGUUUAUCUUCAUGGAUCUAUGAUUGACCUCCUAGUAAAAUUCUAAGUCUUGCCUUUCUUCCCUGCUGUUUUAGCAUUUCUUUGUAAAAUGUUAGCUUCAAUUAAUUAGCCAUUGGUACUUACUGUAGCUACACAUAUUAAAAGGCAAAGUGUUUCUGAAGGCAAUUUCUUUUUAAUAUGCCCGAAUGAAUGAGGCUUCAUCCUUUCCAUAUUCUUACUCUUUACAGGAGUUCAAAUGCAAAUAAGCUCCACCUCCCUGCACUUGUAGUCUAAAAAGUAAAAGGGGCGAUCAGGUCCAUCUCAAAGGUCACACGUAAUAGCCUCCCUGGGCUGAUCAUUCCCUCUCCUUGUAAUUGCAGUAUCCUGAGUAGCAGUUUAAUUUUCAUCAAACAUCGGAGUAGUUUAGUUGUUUGACAGGAGGAGAAUAAGGCUGAAAGCCUCAAGUGAAGGAUCUUGCAGCUUGUAAAAGCAAUUUCCAAAAAUGAAACCCAUUCAUCGUAAACAAAAGCACAAACACUUGUAGCAGUUUAUAAUGCUUUUGGUUUAAUCUCAAUUAGUCUUUCUCCCCUGGACUAGAAAUCCAGUAUAGUUUGCCAUUAAUUUAUUGAAUCUGGUUUUGGACAAUGCUUCUGUAGUGUAGCUGCACGUCCUGGUACUGUAUCCUCUGACUUUAUUUUCCAUGUAUUACAAAAGGAAAAAAAAAUUGAGAUUACACUGGCAUAAACUCUAGUUUGCACAGUUCACAGCUACUACUUGUGCAGUAAUUGCUUUAUGCGGCUGUAAUCCAUAACCUGUGAAGACAGCACAUCAUCUAAAUCCCAUUCCAAAUAAUAUUUGUGUAGUGUUAGCUGUGAAUUUACCCUGUACAGCUGUAUCUCUAUAAAUAUAAUUCCAUGUAUUAAUAGUCACAGAAAGACUGUAAGUGAGCAACUAUUUUUAUGAAACGUACCACUAUGGAUAAAUUAACUUUUACAGAAAUCUUGUUUACUGUAUGAUAUUCUAAAACACUGUCAAAUAAAAUAUAUAUCCAAAAAUCUUUUCUUUUUCCAACUAUA